CUCUCCAAAAUUCUACUUGCAUAUGCUGCAAAAACCCAGGAUGACUUUUGAGGAGAGAGAGAGAGUCUUUGAAUAAAAGCACAACGUGUUAGAUCUUUUAUUUCUGUAUCCCUCAGUUCUGAGCAAAAUGCCCACACAGUAGGAUCUCGGUAAAUCUUCCUGUCUCUUGGAGUGGACUUCCUUUAGGAUACAGCAAGUUCUGACCGUGACUUCCUAGGAAAGAGUCCUCCCCACUAAAAGAGUGGAAUAGAGUCAGUGGUCAUUUCAGUCACUAAAUUCUCCUGCUGGUGAUGCCAAAGGCAAGACUAGAUCUGCUAGUGAUGCUGAUUUUAAGUGCAUAGAUACUUUUCUGUGUUUCCAUAAAAUGCCAGAAAAUGAGCUGCUCAGCCAAACCCUGUGCCACAGUAAGGGGAACCUUGAAAGAAAGAGGCAAAAGGCAACAUACACCAACUAUGAGGAAUAAGGAAUACACCAACCUUGAAAGAAAGAAGUAAAAGACACAUACACCAACUAUGAGGAAUAAGGCAAAUGGCUCUUCGAAGAGGCUCAAGGCCAUACCAGUCCUCUCAGUUCCAGAGGGGAGGGGCCCAGAGGAGUCAUCUCCCAGCAGGGUGAGAACCAAAAGGUUGGUGAGGUACUGAGGCUACCCAUGGAGGAAUUUGGGAGGGAAUAAACACCUACAUCCACACAAGUCCUUUAGAAGAUUUUUAGCAGCAAGAGUUGGCUACUAAUAGGUCAGCCCUCUUACCUAAAAUGACGCAGUUGCUUUCUAUGAAAGCAUGAUUUUGAUGCUCAGCACUCCACAGAUACAUACUAUGUAAAUGUUAUCACCAUGCACGAGUUCAUACUGUUGCAUAGAACUAGCUGGCAAGUGAGAAACAAAGUGCCAGUUUCUAUGUAGGCAGUGUUUCCACAGUUACUUCAGCCCUUUCUACCCCAGUACAGCAGAAUUCUGGGUAGUGUAAAUAAUUGAUGAAUUCAAGCAUUGGUACAUUAUAUAGGGGCCAGUUAGAGACCCAUGUAGGUAUUUUCUCUGUUAUGGUUCUUCUAAAAAAGUUUUUAUCUUGUUAAUACUGGUUUUGACUUUUUUAUUUUUUUAUUAUUAUACUUUAAGUUCUAGUGUACAUGUGCACAACGUGCAUUUUUGUUACAUAUGUAUACAUGUGCCAUGUUGGUGUGUGCCGCACCCAUUAACUCGUCAUUUACAUUAGGUAUAUCUCCCAUUACUAUCCCUCCCCCCUCUCCCCACUCCACGACAGGCCCUGGUGUGUGAUGUUCCCCUUCCUGUGGUUUUGACUUUUUUUUUUUUUUUUUUAAACAUAGAAUCAACAGUUCGAUACAGGUAGAGGAUUCAUUAAUGAGAAUGCAUCUUUCACUACUGUGCAAUGAAUAUUUGAUGGCAUUUUUAUUCCCCUGAAAUGUUCAGGUGCUGUAAAUACUUCUGAAAAAGCUUUUCAGGGAGUUCACAUUACUUCUCAGAAUAGGCUAAUGUUUGUUUGUAUCAUACUUCUAAGAUAGAAUGGUGGUCUCCCCGUCCCCCAUGUCAUAUGUCUCUCUCAUAACCCCAUGAAAAGGUGUAGAAGAGAUUCUCCAUGUGGAAAAUUUCUGUGAGGUUUCAGAAGCCUAUAACAUUAUUCCCAUAAUUGACUGAUCUUUAACUUGCCAUUCUUAAGUAAGAGGAUUCAAUUAAAAAAAUUUUUGUUUUACUUCGCCAACAUCAGUGGUCAAGUGUUUCUCUAAUUUGUUUUGAACUGCGUGGCAGGAGUGGAAUUUGAGCCCACACCUCCCUACAAAGACCAGAAUCAUUUCUUUUUUAUAAAACUCUGAGAAUAGUGAUACUGCUUUGCCAAAAAUGAAAAGACUUUCUAUAAGCACAUAGACAAACAUGAUGAGUGGGUAUGAAAUGCUUACCAGUAAUGGUAGUCAUAGGUUGUAUAAUCUUUCUGUGCUAAGAAUUAGCAGUAGGUUGGCUAGUCAUUGGCCUGGGAUGGCUUGAUGUGACCCAGCUUCCAGGUAGGAACCUAAAUCAGAUACCAAGAGACUUUUCUACCUCAGGAACCUAAACACAGAACAGAGCACCCUCCUCAAAUCUAUCAAGUCAGUUAAUUGUUAAAUUCAUAAUUCCACAGUUUGUAAUCACUCUUAUGGAUGGUUAGGCAGUUAACUAGCCAUAUGGAAGUGAUAGGGAAUUCCAAUCAAGGUAAAAUUGAGCAGCAGAGUGAAAAUGCAAAAGCUUUCUAGUUUUUAUUCUAUAUGGGAAGAUGAGUUCUGGAGCUGCGAAGAACACCUGGUUAAUGAGUUCUUGAGACAUGUCUAAUAGCUUUUCCCUAAGGCUAGGGACAUGAGAAAUAAUCAUGAAAUUUGAGAGAAAGGAGAUUUAAGAUAAGGUUGUCAAAAGGGAUAAGUAUUUUAAAGACACCUCAGCCUACUGGACUUUUGGUUGCAUGCAAAAUAGAGUAUACAGCCUGGGAGUGCACAGCCAGCUAUGAACUUCCUGAUUCACAGUGAAUGUUAUUUUUUGCCUCUGCAUGCACCUCCCUUGCUCUGACUUGCCCUGCUGUGCCGUGGCCUUCCACACCUUCUGCAUGACUGGACUUUGCCUUCAGCGUCUUCACAUGGCCUGUAGGGCACAGCCUCUUGCAAAGGAAGUGCUCAGAAGGUAUAUUUAGAAAUGAAUUUCCUAAACAGUUGAAAGUAUCCUUCAUAAACAAAAGGACUGAUUAUAUUUUUUCCUCUCUUUUUUUGAUGAUUAAAAGCAUUUUAAAUACUAUUUUUUUUGUCUUGAUUGAUUAAAGGAAAUACUAUGUAUGGCAGAAUAUUGGCAGUGAGUAGAAAUUCAAAGCAGGCUUAAUAUUGACUUUAUGGAGAGAUAGGGAAAGGCCAAUUAAAUAAUGAAAGUAAAGGCUUACAUAAUAUUGUAUACUAAUGUAAUUAAAUAAAUGUGGAAAAAUCCGUGUAUUUAAAUGGGGGGUCUGAAUCUAACACCUCACCACUCACUUUCUAAUAGAAGCUAUUUUUGUAAGUGUGUGGGAGUCUGGCAAUAUCCUUUCAGAUAGAAAUCAUUGUAGGUUUAAAUCACUGAUAUAGCAUGGAUUAAGCAGAUGAAAGCAAUGAAGGAAGAGCCUGUUUAGAUUCCAGAGAAUAAAAUUCAUAGAACUGUGAGAGGUGGAGCUUGAAAUACUGCCACAGUUUUGAAGUUGUUUUAGUGACAUCAUGUUUCUAUGCAUGAUUCUUACAUAUGUAUCAAAGUGUGGGAGUAUUCAUCUUCCAGAAUUCUAGAAUUCAUGAUUUUGUAAUCUAGCCUAUCAAGUGAUUCACAUACAAAGCCUUUCUUUUUUCCUGAACUGUUGAAUUUGGAUAAAUUGUGAAUUGUGUUUUUUUUUUAAACUAGUAAAGUGGUAUCUUUUGGAAUUGCUUCUUAAUUGUCUAUGGUAAGGCAUAAGGCACGUUGCAUGUUGCUUUUCAAAAUAUCUUGAUAUGAUAAAGUGCAGUUCAGAACUGUAAUAAAAGGGGCUAUUUUUUAAUAUCCCAGAGAGUUUAAUUAUAAAAUAAUUUUGUAGUAACAUGAUCUUUGACCAAAUUUCCGUCUAGCAUUGUAGAUCUUCAUUUUGUAUAUUUUCUUUAGUUUUAUGACAAGAAUAAUAAUACUCAUUCUCCUCCUCAUAUUUUCUUAGGACCUGAGUAAGUACUACAGCUUGAUGCUCAGUCCUCACUUACUGUGGCUAAUUCGAGAGACACUUGAUACUGAAAUGCAAGAUCUGGUGUUACUCAGCACUGGUUUAUGAGCACCAGGGGCUAUGCUUUUUGCUAUAUACACAUCACAGUCUGCCUUCAUAGUACCCCUGCAGAGGAGGUGGUAUUGUGCCUGUUGUACAGGGUAAGAAACAAAGGUUCAGAAAACUUCAGUAACUCUUUCAAGGCUUGAGGUCACACCACAAAGAACGUAGUUUAUCCAGGAUUUGAACUCAGCAUUCUGUUACCCCACAGCCGUUGCUCUUUCUGUUGUGCAGCAUUGAUUCUCUUGUAACUUUGUCUAUUUUCAUAAAUUAAUUUGUCUCUAGGAACAGGCAGCUUUCUCUCUUCUAGAUGUUAUGACCUAUUUUCUGUCUCAUAACAUGGCCAAGUACAUAAUUUGAGACUGUGUUUUUUAUUGUUUGUCUUACGUUGUUUUUCAGCAAAUAAACAUUAACCAAAAUCAGGUAGCCAAGAUGCCAAAUCAUGUAGCAAACCUACACAUAGGGGGAACAAAGAAAAACUGAACAUGCUAAGUAAGCCAUCUUUUCACCUAGCGUCUUAAUUGUGAGGCAUAUAUGUUGCAUGUUGCUUGUGAAAGUAUCUUAGUAUCAUAAGAUGCAGUUCAGAAUUGUAAUCAAAGAAGGGGCUAUUUUUUAGUCUUCCAGAGAGUUCAGUCUCCCCCCCCUUGGGCAUGCACCCUGGGGCUUUGGGACCUCAGAGGUUCUUUUUAUUAGCUUAAUUGUUUAGCUCGUUAACUGUUCCCUUGUGCUUUCCUAGUAAGGGGCACUUCCCUACUAGAAGGGGAUGAACUCCAGCUGGUAUUGAGGUCAUAUGAGUGUAGUUUUGAUUGAAAAAAAGAACAACAUGGACACAAAUAUUGGCCAUGACAGGUAGAUAUCAAAUAGUUCUUUCAUAUAUUUUAAUUUUAAUUUAAUUUAAUUUAAUUUUUUUUUUUUUGAGACAGAGUCUCGCUCUUGUUGCCCAGGCUGGAGUGCAAUGGCGCCAUCUCGGCUCACCGCAACCUCUACCUCCUGUGUUCAAGCAAUUCUCCAGCCUCAGCGUCCCGAGUAACUGGGAUUAUAGGCAUCCGCCACCGUACCUGGUUAAUUUUUGGAUUUUUAGUAGAGACAGGGUUUCACCAUGAUGGCCAGGCUGGUCUUGAACUCCUGGCCUCAGGUGAUCUGCCCACCUCGGCCUCCCAAAGCACUGGAAUUACAGGCAUGAGCCACCACCCAGCCGAAUUUUUAUUUUAUUUUUCUGAGACAGAGUCUUACUCUGUCACUCAGGCUGGAGUACAGUGGCACAAUCUAGGCAGAGGCAACCUCUGCCUCCCAGUUUCAAGCGAUUCUCGUGACUCAGUCUCCUGAGUAGCUGGGAUUACAGGUCAGUGCCACCACGCCCGGCUGAUUUUUGUGUUUUUAGUAGAGACAUGGUUUUACCAUGUUGUCCAGGCUGGUCUUGAACUGACCUCAAUUGAUCCACUCGCCUCGCCUCCCAAAGUGCUGGGAUUAUAGGCGUGAGCCACUGUACCUGGCCCAUUUUUUUUAAAAGUGAAAAACCAAACUAAAGUGUGAUAAUAGUUUUGAACAUUUAGUGGAGUGUAAGAAAAGAGAACCCAUUUGACUCAGGUUCACUGAUAAAGGGUUCUAUUUCCUUUUCUAGGAGUUGAGCAUUGCUGUUGGUUUUGUGGGAGGUAAUAUUUACACAAUCAUACUGCUGUGGAUGUAGCUAAAUAGUUUAUUGGUUAAUCCCCACACAAGACAGGAAAGAUGUAAUUAUAACUACAGAGAGAAAACAAUCAUCAAGGUUUUAAAAUCUAGCAAUGCAAAGGGAGUGAAAGAGCAGACAGAAGCCUGAGGCUAGAAGGCAGGAAAAGAGGCAGGAGGGAGAGGGACCUUGGUACUCAUUUUCUUCUUUUACAUGGUGGGAUGUAGAGAAAUACUGUGUAAUACUGCUGAAACAGGAAACAGAGCUAACCAAUUGAAGGACUAAAAAUAGUAUAAUCAAGAAAACUAGAGACAAAAUAGAGGUGAAGUAAGUGUGAAUGAGUUAGAUACGGGGGAGGCGGUAAGUCAGUAGAUUCUGUCUGAAGUUGACACAUCAGGGAUAGAAGCCUGUCAUUUCGUUAAGCUGAUCACCAUAGAAGGACUGUAAAAGCAAUAAUGGAAGGGAGUGGAAAUGGGGAGUAUGGGCCCAGAGACACUUACUUUCCACUUUUUACCAUGCUUCUGUUUAGGAAAAGUUACCUGCACAUGUAUUACUUUUCAUAUAAUUUAAGAAAAAGGAAGAAUUUCAGCAAAUUGUAGAUGUACAGUGUCAGGAAUAAUUUUCCACGCAUACUAUGACAUUACUGUUAUUACUAGGGUACCAGGGACUGCUGUUGCCACUGGUGGAGGGUUCUGGUUUCCAAAGAAUCAGGACAAGGGGGUUAAGUUGGGGCAAGGUGACAGAUAACUACACCCAUGAUCCCAUUCAGGUAUUCAACUGGUUUCAUGGUUGGAUCCUGAUCAAAAUAUGGCAGAAGUAUUUAGAUAGAAGAAACAUAAAGGAAAGAACCCCACUAGCCUUCUUCAGACUUGCAAAGUGAAAAUGUUCCUCCUAUAAGGGGCUGCUGGGGAAGCCCAGCACCCUGGCUAAUGCUCCAGGGUUGCAGAACCCCGCUUCUUGUUCUGGGAUGCCAUGGCCAUUCUGGAGAGUGCAUGUCUGCGUUGCCUUUGUUUUCUCUAGUCUGAGGAGUGGCUGAGCUUCAGGGCACUGACUUCCUCCCAGGAACUUCCUGAAAGGGGAAAUUUCGACUUUGCUGUAUGAACACUCUGAAUGCCUGUGGGUUGAACAAUGGUAGCUGCUGUUGUUUUUUUUUCAAGAGGGAGCUCAAUUUUGUUUUGACCUUGGGAAGUGUGGAUAGUUGUGUUCAUGGCGCCUCCAUGUGGGCGGUCAAGGAAGAAAGUCUUGGGGUAGGAGCCCUUGGAGAAUGAGGACUUGAUUUUGCCAUUUUUGCUUUUGGCCUUAAUCUGUGUUGUUGUGGAGACAGUAGUACUGAGAUGGGGUUAGGGUGGGGAAUGGAGUGUGGAGAAGGGCCAGGGAAGGAGCUAACUAGAGGGUUAGUGCCAAUAGCUGAAGGAAGCGCUCUGCCUUAGGAGGCUUUAUAAAUAGUUGCCUUUAUCCAGUGUGUCUCAUUUUGCCUCUCUCAGGCCUAAUUUCUAAAUAAUCCCAUUUUUCAAGAUAAAGGAGAUAAAAAGGGGUACUCUGAGAUUCUCCCAGCAGGUGUGAAAUCCUGCCUAAUAAUUGUAGCUGCAGAUUUCUCUAUCAGGAAUUGAUUUGCUGUUAAUAUAGUCUAGUGCUUGAUGCUUGCAAAGUCAUAUGCCUUUGGGAUUCAGGCAGGUGGUUUUAAAUGAGUGACACUGGGUGGGACCUCUGGCCAACUAAAACCUUAUGGCUCAUUGAAGCUGUUGUUCAGCUUUGAAUGUUGCCAUGUAUGGAGAGCAGGUUUUUAGGCUUGCCAGAGCUUCCAGUUUUUCCAGGUAAAUAAAAUAUCUGCUUUUUAUGUGAAAUCUCUUGGAUUUUAAAUGUUGCCAACUAAUCGAAAAGCUUAAAACUAUUGUCUAGAAUUAAAAAACAAGCCUGGGCCGGGCGUGUUGGCUCACGCCUGUAAUCCCAGCACUUUGGGAGGCUGAGGUGGGUGGAUCACGAGGUCAGGAGUUUGAGACCAGCCUGACCAAUAUGGUGAAACCCCAUCUCUGCUAAAAAUGCAAAAAUUAGCCAGCGUGGCAGCGCGUGCCUGUAAUCCCAGCUACUUGGGAGGCUGAGGCAGGAGAAUCACCUGAACCUGGGAGGCGGAGGUUGCACUGAGUUGAGAUCGUGCCAUUGCACUCCAGCCUGGGCAACAGAGCGAGACUCUGUCUCAAAAAAAACAAAAACAAAAACAAAAAAAAACCAAAAACCAAAAAACAAAAACCAAGCCUGUUGAGUGGAUAGUUUUUGGCUGCCAAUUUUUACCACUGGUUAGGACUCUUAACACCUGACCCCAGUUGUUCUUCAGCCUUGAUUGUUGAAAAUGAGCUGAACAUUUACUGGGCACUUUACUUUGUGUUCUACCUUUUUCUAAAAGCAUUUAAAGAUGCUUUUGUUAAAUAUAAACUAAUAUAAAUUAGAAGCAGGUGGAAGACAAAAAGUUAAAACAACUGCAGGAUAGUAAAUGGAAUCAGAAUGAAAUGAUACACAUAAUGUCAGUGAACCUCAAACUGGGCAUGGAGCUUGCUAGCAACUGGCAUAACAUAGAAGCCUUAUCAGUUAUACCACUUGUAGUAUCUUUAAAACAAACUGUUUAACAGUGACAUGGCUCUUCCCGAUGCCAGGAUCAGAAGGACAGCUCUCAGAAGGGUCUUCAAAAGAACACACUGAAUCCUAUGACUCUCAUUGCAGUGAGAGCUUUAUAGGAUUGUUCUUCCUGUUGCUCUCCAUUAAAAGGCCGAUAACGGGGCUGAGCGCAGUGGCUCACGCCUGUAAUCCCAGCACUUUGGGAGGCUGAGGCGGGUGGAUCAUGAGGUCAAGAGAUCAACCAUCCUGGCCAACAUGGUGAAACCCCGUCUCUACUAAAAAUACAGAAAUUAGCUGGGCAUGGUGGUGUGCGCGUGUAAUCCCAACUACUCGGGAAGCUGAGGCAGAAGAAUUGCUUGAACCUGGGAGGAGGAGGUUGCAGUGAACCGAGAUCGCGCCACUGCCCUCCAGCCUGCUGAGAGAGCGAGACCUUGUCUCAAAAAAAAAAAAAAAAAAAAAAGGGGGGGCUGAUAACAGUAAAAGUGUAGUUUGGGAAAUGAGAUACUAGCAAUGGGACCUUGGGUAAGUUGCCCUAUUUUUCUAAACCUGUUUCCUUAUCUGUAUAAUGAAGAUAAUUAUAUUAAUACAAAGCAACCACUCUCAAAGGACCAUUGUGAGGCUUAGCUGGUACAGUUUGAAUAAAGCACUUAUUGCAGUUCUUGGUACCCAGUAAGCAUUCUGUAAAAGUUGGCUGUGGUGAGUUAGAGAAUUGCUAGCAGUGAGAGCUUAGUUGUCAGAAUGAUUUAAAUGUGACUGUCCAAGAUUUAUUUACGGCACUUAAAUGUUUUCGUUUGCUGCAAUACAAUUUUUUAUCCCACUUAAUCCUGGGUCACCAAAAAAGUGUUGAGUUACUUAUGUACAGAGGAUUUUGCAAGGCUCUAGGGGAUGGGCCCUGUAGGGAACUUGUAUUUUGGCUAACUAGGUAAAGACACAAUACAAGACAGGGAGCACCAAGGGCCAUCUGAGCAAGGCUGAGUCGAUCCAUUGAGGGGUUGUCACAGUGGGCUGAUACCAAACUAAGACUUCACAGUGAUCCACUUUAUUAUUUGGCAGGUAGAAUUUUAUAGUUUGAAUCAUUCCAAACACUGUACAAGAAUAUUUCAAGCUAUGCAACAAAGUAAAAUGAGGAUUUACCUGAGUAUUUUGUAUGAAUCAUUAUAGGAGCAAGGUGAACAGCAGCAAUCCGUCAUGCUUUGCAGUUUGUAUUAAUUAAACCUUAGAACGUGGGGUAGUUAGGUUGAGCCAUCCUUUGCAUAUUUUUUCAUUACAGAGAGUCUUCUCAGCUGGCCUUGGGGCAUGCAGAGAGGUGGAGAUCUGUGUGAGCAGCUAUAGCACUAGGCAGCCUUGCAUCCUGGGUGUUGAAAGUGCAGGCCAUUAUCCUCCCCUCUGACCUCCAAGAUGUUAGGUGGCCUUUCUGUGCCUCAGUUUUAUCAUCUGUAAAUUGGGUAUGAUUGUACUAGUGCCUAGUACAUAAGGAGUGCUGCAAAGAUUACAUGAGUGUCUUUAAAGUCCUUACAACAGUAUCUCACACAUAGUAAGCAUGGCAUGUGGUAGUUACUAUCAUUAGUCCCUCUUGGAGCAAUGUAUAUUAAAAUUUUAAAGACAGCUGUCUGGUCAGGAUUGGACAUGCAGCCUGUAGUUUCAGAACAGAAUGCAGCUGACUGUGUACAUGGGGAUAACUUUAUAAUGCCCUGGACCUCAUUAGCUCAUGGCUGUGGAAUGGAUGGGGGCAUCUGGAGGGUCCCUGUUUCAGACCCAGAAAUUGAAAGCUCAGCCCCAGCCUCAGCUCCAGCUUACUUGCUCUGUUGAUAUAUGGCGAGUUCUUCAGUGUCUUAAAGUUUCUUUGUGCCUACAAAACAGGCUUAACCUUUCAUUCUUGGUGUGUGCUGAAUUUUCAUAAGAAAUUCAGGAAUAUAAUGGUUGGAUGAAUGAGUUAUAUUUUAAAGAUUAUUAAAAAUUAAAGGAGAUGCAAAUAUAACAGCUAAAUAUUAUUGCUUUGACUUCUAGGUUUUUGUAAGAAUCUAAGUAUAUAGUAUUCACCAUAUGAGAAAAUUAAGUUUUACCUUAUUAUAUAAUAACCCAGUAAGGACUUUAGUUAAUUGUUCAAUUUUUUAAAAAAAAUUUCCUGGAAAUCUCUAAGAUUGAACAUGAAGACCCAGAAAAUGACUUCAUUGCCCCCUACUUUGAGUCUCACUCUGUCGCCCAGGCUGGAGUGCAGUGGCACAAUCUCAGCUCACUGCAGCCUGUGCCUCCCACAUUCAAGCGAUUCUCCUGCCUCAGGCUCCCAAGUGGCUAAAGAUCAUAGGCACACGCCACCAUGCCCAGCUAAUUUUUGUAUUUUUAGUAGAGACAGGGUUUCAUCAUGUUGGCCAGGCAGGUCUUGAACUCCUGACUGCAAGUGAUCUGCCUGCUUUGGCCUCCCAAAGUGCUGGGAUUACAGGUGUGAGCCACUGCACCCGGCCAUUGCUUCCUAUUUCUAUGUUUCCCUCAAAGAAUUGACUUGAAUCUCAGUGUGGUUGUGAACUCUUCCUAAUGAAUUUCUGCUCCUUCUGCUGACAGCAUUUUCCAUACACGUUAGACCUGCUUUUUUGGGAGAGUUGUUCUGAAGUGAGUGGUUCACAGAAAUGAGGGCAUACACCAGCUGCGUGUAAAAAUAUGCCCCUGCCCUUACUGCUGCACAUGCAGGGACAAGGACUGGGGAGCCUUGCAGUAGAGCCAGGUAGCUCAGCCUACUUGUGUCUGAAGAUGUGGGGCUGAUGUCGUGAGUUCUGUUUAGGAGUAGUUCAUUUCAUGUUUUCCUUAAAGGAUAAUUUUUGGCCAUUCCCACACAUUUAUUCUUCAUAUAAAAUUUAGAAUCAUUUGUUAACCUCUAAAAAAACCCCAUUGGUUUUGAAUGUGAUCACACUAAACAUAUAGAUUGAUUUUGGGAAAAUUUAUACUUAAAGUCCAGUAAUGUGGUAUGUCUUGUUUUUUUUUUUUUUUCCUUUCUUUUUUAAAUGUCUUCUCCUUUUUACUUAAGUAAAGGAAUUUUUUUUUUUUUUUUGAGAUGGAGUCUUGCUGUUGUCACCCAGGCUGGAGUACAAUGGUACGAUCUCGGCUCACUGCAAACUCCACCACCCGGGUUCCAGCAAUUCUCCUGCCUCAACCUCUUGAGUAGCUGAGAUUACAGGUGCCCACCACCACGCCCGGCUAAUUUUUGUAUUUUUAGUAGAGAUGGGGUUUCCCCAUGUUGGCCAGGCUGGUCUCGAACUCCUCAGGUGAUCGAUCCACCCGCCUCGGCCUCCCAAAGUGCUGUGAUUACAGGUGUGAGCUACCGUAACUGGCCAGUAAAUGAAAUCUUGUCCUUUUAUUUAUAUGGGUCCUACGUUUCCUGUUAAAUUUAUUCCUAGUUAUUUUAUAUUUUGUUUUUGAUUGUUGUAGUGAAUAGACUUCUUAAAUUGUAUCUUGUAACUAGUACUUACUUAUUAUGGAAAAGCUGUUGGGUUUUUCACAUUUAUUAGUGGGCUUAUGAAGCCCAUUUACUGAAUUGCCUGAAAAUGGAACCGAUGUUACUUGCAUUUGUUUUGUGAACAAAGGAAAAAAAAACAGUAUGAGAAACUUAUAUUUUAAUUUUAUUCUCUGUUAGACUCUACAGUGCAUCCUGGGUCCCUCUUUUUACUCACUGUUGUGUCCCUAGUACCUGCCUCAGGAUUUGCCAUGGUGCGUGCACGAUUAAUAUUUGUAGAAUAUUUCUUAACUUUCUUAAUUCUAUAAUAGUUUUUUCUCUUGGGUUUUUUAAAGAAAAGCAAUUAUAUCAUCCCCAAAUACUAAUGAUUUUGUUUCUAGUAUUUUUUUUUCAUUUUAAUUGUUAUUAUUUUGGCUAGAACUUUCCUUGUAAUAUUCAAUGAUAGUCACCCUGUUGCAGAUGACACGAUUGUACAUUUAGAAAACCCCAUCAUCUCAGCCCAAAAUCUCCUUAAGCUGAUAAGCAACUUCACCAAAGUCUCAGGAUACAAAAUCAGUGUGCAAAAAUCACAAGCAUUCCUAUACACCAAUAACACACAAACAGAGAGUCAAGUCAUGAGUGAACUCCCAUUCACAAUUGCUACUAAGAGAAUAAAUACCUAGGAAUACAACAUACAACUUACAAGGGAUGUGAAGGACCUCUUCAAGGAGAACUACAAACCACUGCUCAGGAAUAAGAGAGGACACAAACAAAUGGAAAAACAUUCCAUGCCCUUGCCAGAACUUCCAAUACUAUAUUGAAUAGGAGUGGUGAGAGAGGGCAUUCUUGUCUUAUGCCGGUUUUCAAAGGUAAUGCUUCCAGUUUUUGCCCAUUCAGUAUGAUAUUGGCGGUGUGUCUGUCAUAAAUAGCUCUUAUUAUUUUGAGAUACGUUCCAUUGAUACCUAGUUUAUUGAGAGUUUUUAGCAUGAAAUGCUGUUGAAUUUUGUCGAAGGCCUUUUCUGCAUCUAUUGAGACGAUCAUGUGGUUUUUGUCGUUGGUUCUGUUCAUGUGAUGGAUUACGUUUAUUGAUUUGCGUAUGUUGAACCAGCCUUGCAUCCCAGGGAUGAAGCCAUCUUAAUUGUGGUAGAUAAGCUUUUUGAUGUGCUGCUGGAUUUGGUUUGCCAGUAUUUUAUUGAGGAUUUUUGCAUCGAUGUUCAUCAGGGAUAUUGGCCUAAAAUUCUCUUUUUUUGUUGUGUCUCUGCUAGGCUUUGGUGUCAGGAUGAUGCUGGCCUCAUAAAAUGAGUUCGGGUGGAUUCCCUCUUUUUCUGUUGAUUGAAAUAGUUUCGGAAGGAAUGGUAUCAGCUCCUCUUUGUACCUCUGGUAGAAUUCGGCUGUGAAUCCGUCUGGUCCUAGACUUCUUUUUGGUUGGUAUGCUAUUAAUUAUUGCCUCAAUUUCAGAACCUGUUAUUGGUCUAUUCAGGGAUUCAACUUCUUCCUGGUUUAGUCUUGGGAGGGUGUGUGUAUCCAGGAAUUUAUCCAUUUCUUUUAGACUUUCUAGUUUAUUUGUGUAGAGGGGUUUAUGGUAUUCUCUGAUGGUGGUUUGUAUUUCUGUGGGAUCGGUGGUGAUAUCCCCUUUAUCAUUUUUUGUUGCAUCGAUUUGGUUCUUCUCUCUUUUCUUCUUUAUUAGGGGUCUAUUUUGUUGAUCUUUUCAAAAAACCAGCUCCUGGAUUCAUUGAUUUUUUUUGAAAGGUUUUUUAUGUCUGUAUCUCCUUCAGUUCUGCUCUGAUCUUAAUUAUUUCUUGUCUUCUGCUAGCUUUUGAAUUUGUUUUCUCUUGAGUCUAUGGUUCUUUUAAUUGUGAUGUUACGGUGUUGAUUUUAGAUCUUUCCUGCUUUCUCUUGUGGGCAUUUAGUGCUAUAAAUUUCCCUCUACACACUGCAUUAAAUGUGUCCCAGAGAUUCUGGUACGCUGUGUCUUUGUUCUCAUUGGUUUCAAAGAACAUCUUUAUUUCUCCCUUCAAAUCUUAGUCUAUGUUUUUAAAGUUAAUGUUUUAAGGAUGAAUAGGCAGAAUGGGAAGAGGACUGCCCCUGCCUUCAACCCCAGAUUUUGAUUAUAGCCCACCAUACUGCCUUUGAAAAGCCAUAGGUGCCUCUCUUCCUGAUGUGUGUGUGCAGUUGGGCCGUUGGUAACUUUUUGAUAACACUGAAUCAAGUUGGGAAGAAAACUUGUGUCCAGGGCAGAUGUGAUGCAGGUUUGCAAUGUGGAACUGAGCAGGAGCACGGGGCAGAGUAGAGAGGAGGAGUUUGUGACUCAGUCAGUUUUUUUUGUUUGUUUGUUUGUUUUUUUUUUUUUGUGGAGAUGGAGUCUUGCUCUGUUGCCUAGGCUGGAGUGGAGUGGCAUAAAUCUGGGCUCACUGCAACCUCCAUCUCCCGGGUUCAAGCGAUUCUUCUGUCUCAGCCUCCCAAGUAGCUGGGAUUACAGGCGUGCACCACUGCACCUGGCUAAUUUUUGUGUUUUUGGUAGAGACAGCGUUUCACCAUGUUGACGAGGCUGGUAUCAAACUCCUGACCUCAGGUGAUCUGCCCGCCUCUGCCUCCCAGAGUGCUGGGAUUACAGGCAUAAGCCAUCACUUUCGUAACAAGGUUCAGAUCUUUGGCUCAUGAAGUUGCUCAUGAAGAAUUUGGUGGUGAGUUAGAGAAAUGGGUACUGGUCUCUGUGUCUACGGAAUGCAUGCCUGAAAUUAAGACAACACUUUGCUCCUUUUGCCUUACAUUUAGUAGGCAUGCAUUACAUGCCUGAUGGAUAUAUGAAUUUGAUGCCUUCACAUAUUUAAAGAAAGAGCUGCCCCCAAUUUCCUGGAAAAUCCAUAGUGUUGAACUGUUGAUGUGGCUAGAAAGUAAGCUGGGUUGUUUUCCAGUGCUCUUCAAACUACUGAAGAUUUUGCUGUGCGAUAUUUAAAACUGUUAGUGUAUUAGUAAAAUUCAUAGUAUGUACUUAUAUAAAACAUACAUUAGUAUAAUCUGUAUUAUAUAUAAUGUAACCUCUCUUCCAUCAUCUACAUUUUAUGACUUUUUGUUUCUAAGUUGGCCUUAAUUGUAUUCUUCCAUGUCAGGAAAUGUUAAAUUGGCUGUCGCAUCAGGCUAAUUGUAUAGGGAGGCAAGAUCUUGGGCAGUAAAGCUAAUUCCUGAGUUUAAAUUGGAAACUUUGAUGAUUGCAUUAACUUUCAGUCCAGCAAAAAUUCUUAAAUUGAUGCUUUAGGGCGCUGGAUGGUAAUUCGGGUGUGUUAGAAAAUUACAGGGAAUCACAGGAGUGUGAAAUCAUUAAGAAAACCACAGUUGUAUUUACCACCUGCCAGGUGGAAAGGCCAGAGGGAGAAUUGGGGUGUUGAAUAAGACUGAAUGGGCUGCUUGGCUGCAUUAUGAAGGAGUUACUGUAUCUCCCUGGAUUAGCAAUAACAGACCUGGGGGUGCAUGCAGACCAACGGCAAACCUCAAAGAGUAAAUAUGCUUUAAUUUCUUCAGGGAGAAAGUGAAGUCCUACCAUGAUUGGUUGAAAAUAUUUUUAUCUGGAGUAAGCUCUUGGCUCCGCCAUCACACCUCACUAGGCAGAAGAGCACUGUCCAUUAAGGUGCCCUCACCUGGGUGCAUUUGCUGGUGGCAUCACUUCCCCCAGACUCUCUGGGAGCAGAAUCACCUUGCCACAGGAGGUGAUUUCCCAUAAAAUCCCCAUACUUAGGGGUUACUUAGCCAGUGAAUUCUGGCUCUGGUAUUCUCUCUGAGUUCCUCUUUAAGAGCCCCGGCAUAAUUGUGUCUCUGUUUUGGCAAACGGCACUGUCUUGCCUUUGGUUUGGUACACUUACGAAAAUUAAUUUGGAAUGAAAUGUAAUUGAAGGCCAUUUACAUCUGAUGGCCAGAUCUAUUAGAACAGAGCAGUGUUGUGGAUUGGGAAAUGGAAAGCAUUUGAGAUAGUGUCUGGGAAAUACAUUCAAUACAUAGAAUGUCACUGCCUUGUCUAAUAGCCUAAUUUAAAUUACUUUUUUGCUUUGCUAUUGCAUUAGGUUGUUCCAGAUAAACUUUGUAGUUCAAGAGGAAGGAAACUGUAUGGUAAAUAAACACUUAGGCAUCCUGAUACAUCUAUUAUCAUUUGUAUAAGAAUUGGAAAACACUUAAAGGAAAUCUUUAGUUUUUGAUUCCUCUAAUGAAAAAAGGAAUAUAAUUCACCUUUUGAAUUUAUUGAUUCAUUUAGCCUGUAGGGAUUUAAUUUCAUCUGAAGUGGUCCUGAAAUAUUUUAUUCUAAGCAGACAACAUCCAUGGUAUUUUUGUUUCUGCCUUUCUACCGUUUCAGUUCUUUAUCUUUAAAAAAAAAUUUGACAUAUAAUUUACAUAAUAUAAAAUUCACCAUUUUAAGUAUACUCAGUGGUUUUUUUAAGUAUACUUAUCACUGAAUUAUAAAGUGAUUAUAAUGUAUACAAUUCAGUGGAUAGUAUACUCGCAGAGUUGUGCAACCAUUACCACCAUCUAAUUGCAGAAUAUUCCUAUCAUCCCAAAGGGAAACCUAAACAUGUUUUUUUGUUGUUGUUUAUUAUUAUUUUUUUUAGAUGGAGUUUCAUUCUUGUUGCCCAGGCUGGAGUGCAAUGGUAUGAUCUCGGUUCACUGCAACCUCCGCCUCCCAAGUUCAAGCGAUUCUCCUGCCUCAGCCUCCCAAGUAGCAGGGAUUACAAGGCAUGUGCCACCAUGCCCGGCUCAUUUUGUAUUUUUAGUAGACAUGAGGUUUCACCAUGUUGACCAGGCUGGUUUCGAACUGCUGACCUCAGGUGAUCCAUCCGCCUCAGCCUCCCAAAGUGCUGGGAUUACAGGAGAGAGCCACCGCGCCCAGCAGACCUGAACAUUUUAACAGUCACUCCCCAUUCUUCCUUCCCCCACCUCUGAUAACCACUAAUCUACCUAAUAUGCCUAUAGAUUUGCCUAUUUUGGACUUUUCAAAUAAAUGGAAUCAUAUGUGGCAUUUUGUGGCUGGCUUCCUUGAGUCACCAUGAUAUUUUUAAGGGUUAUCCAUGUUGUAGUAUGUGUCAGUACUUGAAUUCCUUUUGUUGGUCUUCGAGUGGCUAAGGAGGGGAAACUGAGCACAAGAAGAGGGCACUUUGAGCACAGAGAAAGCUGGACCCGAAAUCUACCAACAAGAGCAGAACCUAAAUAUUGAUGAAGAGGGGCUGAUUCUAGGCACAGCAGGUGGUGGAAGCCUAAUAGUUGUGCAGGUGAUUUUAUAAUGUUAAAAGCACGGAGUGGCCACAGUUGGAUCUGACCGAGGGAACUGAAUCUUUUCCUCCAUGUGAGAGCUGUUGUCAGCCCAACAGGGGUAUACAUGUACCUGGGACAGGGCAGCUUCCCAUUCUGCAAUAGUGGCAUGAUACCCUUUUCCUGAGAUGCAUUCAGGGUUAAAGAAGAUAGUUCACCUACACGUUAGAUUUCCCGUGAAGAUAAAAAGUCCCAAGUUUUGAAAAGCAGAAGGAAUUCUAAAAAGAACUGAAAAACAAAAGCCCAUGGGGAGAGUGAUGAAAUGAGUUUCUGAGAAAGACUGUGAAGAGGGGUUCAAAGCGGCCGCUGACGGACUGCCCGAACCUAGGGCAAUGAAAGACCUGGGGCAGGAAUUGAUGUUGACCGUGGCAGAGGCAGUGGACCUGGUGGGCAGCCCAGAGGAAAAGGCCUUUGGCUUGCUGAGAGAGCUCUUCCAGAACUGAGCAAGAGCAUAGUUUGUUGAAGAAUGGAGAGGUCCACAGUCCAUCUCCUGUGCCAAGGAUUAGUAUUUCAUUUCAAGAAGCGAUUUGGUAGUCACAGAGUGAAUAUUAUUAUUUUUCCACAAAUUCAUUACCUCUUUCCCCUCAUGAGUAUCUUAGCAUUGAAUUUCCUGACUUUAUGAUGAAUAAACUUUGUUUUAGUGUUUAUUAAUGCCCUAUUUACUUUCCCCUGGGUGAAGUUUUGGCUAGUAAUAAGAUUUUGUGUCUCUGCUGUAGUGAGGCAUUGCUGUAGAAAGCCAGGUCUAAGAAAAAUGAAUUUUGUUCCUUUGGGGAAGCAUAAUUACCUUAAAAAAGUUUAAAGUGUGGUUUUCAACUUAGUAAAAUCCUAUUAUAAAGAAAAACGUACAUAGCAAAAAUUUUGCUUGUAGGUAAUACGAUCCUAGUAAAAUAGAAUUUACAUUGUCUCUUAUAGUUUGUUGUAAUAACAUUUUGUAAUAACAGUUUUUUUGCGAUGUAAUUGAUACUCAGUAAGCUGCACAUAUUUAAUAUGUAGAAUUUGAUGUUUUGUCACUUACAUGUGUCUAUGAAAUCAUCACCACCAUGAAGAUAACAAAUAUAUUCAUCAAACCUGAAGGUUGCCUGUGCCUCUUUUUUAUCCUCCCUCCCACCUAUCUCCCCCUCCAAACACUGAUCUGAUUCCUGUCACUGCAGACUUACUUGUAUUUAGUUACGUUUUACACCUGAGGGAACAUACAGUAUGUCCACUUUUGCUUGCCUUUUUCCACUCAGUCAUUUUUAGAUUCAUUUAUGUUGUUGUGUGUCAAUAGUUCGCUCCUUUUUGCUGAGACAUAUUUUGUUGUAUGGAUGUACUACAUUUUCUUUAUCCAUUCAUCUACUGAUGGAGACUUGGAUUGUUUCCAGUGUUUGGCUACGACAAAUAAAGCUGCUGUGAACAUUCAUGCAUAGGUUAUUGAUAGAUACGUGCCUUUUUUUUUUUUUUUUGCUCGGAGUAAAUCCAAGGACUGGAAUGGCUGGAACACAUUACCAGGGGUAUGUUUUACUUUUUAAGAAACUGCCAAGCUGUUUUCCAAAGUGAUUUUUAAUAUUGUGCAGUGUAUGAGAGUUCCAUAUCCUUGCUAGCACUUGGUAUAGUCAGUCUUUUAAAAAAAUGUUGCCAUUUUAAAUGGGUGUGAAGUAUCUAAUUGUGGUUUUAAUUUGCCUAAUGACUAAUGUUGUUGAGUAGUUUCUCAUGUGCUUUGCCAUCUGUAUAACUUUUUCGAUAAAGUGUGAAACCUUUUACUGAUUUUUUUUCCUUUGGAUUACUUGAUUUCUUAUUUUUUUUGUGUAUUAAUAUUUUCUGGAUACAAGUCUGUAUGUAUGCUUUGCAAGUAUUUUCUCCUUGUCUGUGGUUUGUCUUUUUAUUCUUUCAGUGUCUUUUGACAAGCAGUUUUUAAUUUUGAUGAAAUUCAGUUUUGGUGUUAAUUUGAUGGAUAGCUGAGUAUGAUGGGCUGGUGGUCGUAGUUAAUUUUAAUUGUAUGGGAAGUUGAAUGGUUUUUGAGGGUGAGGGGACAGGGUUGAUUCGUGAGGAUUCUGUGGGUGUGGGUGCUUUAUAUAAUUAUGGGUGUUGAUUGGUGGUAGUUGCUGGUUGAACAUUGUUGGUGUUUAUGUUGUGAUUGAAAUUACUCAGGGUAACAGGUUAGAUAAUUCAGAGUAAAGUAAAAAAGGGUGGAAUAAAAAAAGAGGAAAUAAAAUUUAAUUAGGCCUUUUUGAGUAGUUACAGUAAUGGAGGCUGUGAUCUGGGUUUGUGAAAUUGUUUUUGGUAUAGACUUUUCUAGUCACAUUAGGUCUAAUAGAAGUGAUACCAGGUUUUGGCUUGUGGAUAGGCUUGAGUGAAGGGUUGUACAGUGAAUUGUAAUUGAGUAAAAGCCCAGUAUAUUAGAGAAGUUGAGUAUUUGUAAUGGGUAUUUUAUCUUAAGAUUAUUAGUUAUAAAAAUGAGUUCUGUAUUUUUAAAUACAGGUGUCUGGUACUACCUAUUUACCUCUAAGUACAAGUCAGUGGUAUUUCACACUUAAUAUGUUGUUUUCAUUAUUACUUAGUUUCUAAUACUUUCUAAUAUCUAUUUGAUUUUUUUCUUAUGUGUUACUUAGAAGUGGUUUUUCUUGUUGUUUUUGUUUUAUUUUUAGUUUGCAGAUAUUUGGAGAUUUUUCUAGGUAUCUUUCUGUUACUGAUCUCUAAUUCCAUUGUAGUCUGAGACCAUAUUUUAUAUGACUCUUCUAAAAUUUAUUGAGACUGGUUUUAUAGCCCAGAAUAUAGUUUAUCUUGAUAAAUGCUUCAGGUGCACUUGAAAAUAAUGUUUUUCGUUGUUGUUGGGAAAGCAGCCUAUGUCAGUUUGGUUAAGUGGUUAACAGGGUUGUUAAAGUCCUCUAUUAUCUUUGAUGUAUUUCUCUCUACUUGGUUUAUUGCUUUUCUCUCUACUUGAUCUAUUAAGUAUUGAGAAAGGGGUAUUAAAAUCUCUGAGUAUAAUCGUAGACUUGUCCGUUUCUCUCUGCAGUUCCAUCAUUGUUUGCUUCUCAUAUUUUGAAGCUUUGUUAUUGGAUACAUAAACAUUUAGGAUUGUUAUGUCCUUUCGAUAAGUUAACCGGUUUAUCAUUAUGAAAUGAUUGUUUUUAUUUCUGAUAAUAUUAUUUGCAUUAAAAUCUGUGUCUGUUAUUAAUAUGAGAUGACUUCAGAAAUUUUGUGGAAAAAUUGAUUAAAAGAUAAAAAGUAUUAACUUCAUUUCCCAACAUAAGCCCCAUCACGUUCGAGACACUUUUGUAAGCAAUGAUACUAGCCAUGUAGUCCAUUCCUAAAGAAUUGAGGGUCCUGAUGAUUUAACCAUGUCAAGGCAGUCUUUUUUACAUUAUUAACUGUAGAAAAAUGGGUGCCUUUUAAAUUUUUUUUUAAGAUUAGAAAACAAAAAUAAGUCAGAAGAAGCCAAAUUAGGACCAUAAGGUGGAUGCCUAAUAAUUUUCUGUAAAAAUUCUCACAGAAUUGUCCUUUUUUUGAUGAGAGGGAACGAGUAGGAACAUUGUUGUGGUGAAGCUUUCCCAGGCAUUUUUCUGUUAAAGUUUUGACUAACUUUCUCAAACCACUCUCAUAAUAAGCAGGUGUUGGUGUUCUUUGGCCCUUCAGAAAGUCAGUGAGCAAAAUGCCUUCAGUGUCCCCAAAACCUUUUGUCAUGACCUUUGCUCUUGACCCUUCUGCUGCAUUUGCUUUGACUUCCACCUCUUCGUAGCCAUUGCUUUGAUUGUGCUUUUUUUUCAGGAUCGUACUGGUAAGGCCAUGUUUCAUUUCUUGUUAUAGUUCUUCAAAGAAAUGCUUCAGGCUCUUGAUCCUAGUUGUUUAAAAUUUCCACGGAAAGCUCCACUCUUGACUGUAGCUGACCUGGGCACCCACUGAGUGAAAAGUUUGCUAAACUUUAAUUUUUCAGUCAGAAUUAUGUAAGUUGAACCAAUUGAGAUUUCUGUGGUGUCGACUGUUUCUACUGUUAAUUGUCAGUGCUUUUCAAUUAGGGCAAGAUUAAUUUUUUCCUCACAAAUUGAUGUGGAUGGUCUGCUGUUGUGGGCCUUAUCUUCAGCAUCAUUUCAUCCGUUCUUAAAAUGAGCUAUCCACUUAUAAACUGCUGAUUUCUUUGGGGCAUUGUCCUCAAAGUGAUUUCACCGUUCUUCCACGUGAGUUUCACUAUAAAUUUGGCAUUUGUUCUUACUUCAAUUUUAGCAGAAUUCGUGUUGUUCUGAUAGUGGCGUUUUUCAAACCAGUAUCUUCUUAUUCUUAGUGCCUCAAACUAGAUCCUGUUCAGAUAUGUUAUAACAAGUCUGUAUUUUGGUACAAACAUUUUUGAAAUCCAUGCAUAGUUUUUUCAUAAUACACAUUUUCCAUGCACUGUUUUUUUUUUUUUUUUUUUUUUUGAGACUAAGUUUCACUAUUGUUGCCCAGGCUGGAGUGCAAUGGCGUGAUCUUGGCUCACUGCAACCUCUGCCUCCCGGGUUCAAGCAAUUCUCUUGCCUCAGCCUCCCGAGUAGCUGGGAUUACAGGUGCCUGCCACCAUACCCGGCUAACUUUUUGUAUUUUUUAUUAGACACGGGGUUUCACCAUGUUGGCCAGGCUGGCUUCACACUCCUGACCUCAAGUGAUCCGCCCGCCUCGGCCUCCCAAAGUUCUGGGAUUACAGGUGUGAGUCUCUGUGCCUGGCCUUCCAUGCACUUUUUGAAGACCUCUUGUAUAUAUCCACCAUAGUUUUCUUCUAAUUAGUGUUAGCAUGGUGUAUCUUUUCCCCUUCUUUUAUUUUUAAACCAUUUUUAUCUUCAUAUUGAAAGUGUUUUUUGUAAGCAGUAAAUAGUUGUGUCUUUACAUGUAAAGUGUCUUUCUCUCUCUGGCUGCUUUUAGGAUUUUCUCUCUGUUACUGGUUUUCAGCAGGAUGAUUAUGAACUGCCUCAUGUAGUUUUCUUUAUGUUUCUACUGCUUGAUGUUUGUUGAGGGUCUUAGAUCAAUAGUGUUAUAGUUUUCAUUUAAUUUGGAAGAUUUUCAGAUGCUGUUUCUUCAAAUAUUUUUCCUUUUAUAUUCCCACCUUUCUCUCUUCUUCUAGUACUCAAAUUCCAAGUAUAUUAGAUAACUCGAUUUUGUUCCACACUGAGACUGCUCGUUUUUUUCUGUCUUUUUUUCCCUUUGUGCUUCAUUUUUGAUAAUUUCUAUUUUUGUGUCAUCAGGUUCACAUAUGUUUUCUUUUCAGUCUCAUCUGCUCUUAUUUCUAUCUGUUGUAUUUUUCAUUUUAGAUACUGUAUUUUUAAUUGCCAGAAGUUCAUUUGGGACUUUAAAAAUACAUUCCUUUCUCUUUUCUUCAUGUUUAUGUUUUCCUCUACAUUCUUGAGGUGGUGGAACCUAACUAGUACUGCUUUUUAAAAAACAUCCUUGUCUUCUGGGUCUAAAUUUAUUGAGCUUUCUUGGAGUUAUGGGUCACCUUUUCCUGUUUCUUUAUUUGCCUGAUAGUUUUGGGUAAGAUGCCAGACAUUGUGAAUCUUACAUUGUUGAUUGCUGGAUAUUUUGGAUUCCUUUGAAAAGUGGUGGACUUUGUUCUGUCAUGCAGCUGAUUUACUUGGGAUCACUUCAGUAAUUUGUAGUCUUGCUUUUAGGCUUUGUUAGGGUAAGUUUAGAGCAGCCUCUCUUUCAUAGUUACUUAAACUUCACUAUUACGUUGAUACCCUUAUGAAAACUCACUGAUUCCUUCUUUGUGGUGCAGUGAACCUGUGUGAACCUUGGGAAUUGUUCAGACUAUGUGUUCCCAUGUUUCUUUCUCACCCCACUCACGUGUAGAUCAUUAUUAUUGAGCUUCAGGUUCAAGGGCACCCUUCUGCACAUCUCAAGAGCUUUCUCUCUGUUCAGCUCUUUCCUUUCCAGCAUUCUGUCAUGCACAUUCUAGGAUUCUAAGCCUUUCUCGAUUCUGAUCUCUGUUUUUCAACCCAGUGAGAGCACUGGGUUCUUUUUGGGAUCCUCCUUGCCAUGUUGUUGUGUGGAAACUGAAGCCGUGUGGUUAUGUGGAGGCAGUCCUAGGAUUUACCUUAUUUGUAUCCCUGUGCUCCUUGUUGUCGUGUGUUAAAACAAUUGUAUAUUUUAUUUGACUUCCUGGGCUUUUCCCCCCAUUUUAUAAGUGAAUGAGUAUAAAUUCAAAGUCUGGUAAUAUCCAUUAGGUUCUAAAAGCAUCUACUUUUGUUAUUUUAAUUUUAAAUAUAAAAGUGUUACCAGACAUUACUUUUAAAGGAAAGAGUAAAUGGCUAGAAUUUGAACUGUUCUGUUUGUUGGAAUCCAAACUAUGUGUUUCAAAUAAUGAAAUGUAUUAAAGAUAUGUCAUACAGGGAAUGAUCUCAUAUAUCAUUUAUGAAAUGGUUGCUUGUACAAAAUGAUUUCCAGGCCUCCUGUGCUCGUUAGUAUUUCAUUUUAAAGAUAGCCAUGAAAAAUACAGGAAAGGAUGUAAACUCUUAAGUUUCUUAUUUUUCUGUUUAUUCUAGUGUAGUGAAUAGAUCAUUUUUUUUAGGUUAAAGUGAUACUUUAGAUUCUUUGUGGUUUUAAUUUAGCUAGUUUUUCCCAUCUUUUGUAAAUGAUAUUUUGUAUUGACUAUAUUUUCUUAUUUUCUGUAUUAUUGAUGAUCCAGCAUUUGGGGCUUUGCUAAUCCUAAAGACUCCGCCCUCUCUGGGCUAGCUAAUUCCUAGAGUUAACAAGUGACUCCCUGCGGCAUGCCUUUCCUGUGCAAACCAAUCAGUCCAGAGCACACAGCCACCAACCACCUCCUUUAGCUCUCAGAGAUUGAGCCGGGAUCUCUCUUCUGUAAUAUCACUCCAGGGCCAGGGGUAACAGGGCAACUAAGGGCAAUCCCUACAUACCACAGUCCACUGAAAAUAUUCAAAUUAGCCAAUUCUAAUUCUGCCUACCUCGCUUUGCCUGUUUCUUUCUGAAAAAACUACAGUAAAGGACCUGACCCAUGCCUUCUCCUCACUCCCUCUGCCUCCUGACCCAUUCUGGUGUGAUGACCAAACAAUAUCAGUCCUUUUGUCAAUUUCUUACUUUCUGAGGUGGCUGGAAGAGAAGGAAAUAAAGAGAGCAGAAAAAAUGCAAUACAAAAAUAAAACACAAUAAAAGAAAGAUGAGCAGGAUGAUUCCAGUGAGCAUAGAAUUAAAGCAAGUAGAAUUAAAGUUCCCUUACCCUUAAUAACAAAACUAAAGCUAUACCCAUUCUCUUGGUUAAAGAGAAUUAUAUGAAUAAAAAAAAAAGAAAUGGUGUUGAGUGAAGAGGCAAGGAAUCCAUUUAUCAUCCACUGUCAUCCUUCUUUCAGAGGAUAGAGGUGAUAUAGCAGGUCCAAAUUAGCUUCCACAAUUUAGGUUUUACAAUCCAAGGGGCUGACGCAUGGGUGGAACAUGGAGGAUUCCUAGAACCAUGGUGCCACCUUUUUGGGGGGCCUGAAUCUUGACAUCCUUAGUUUCCAAAAUUCUGCUGUAGAAAAACUGAUUGGCAUAUAGAUUUGUAGCAGUCGUUUGGAAAGGAGACUCUUCUGAUUUUUUUUAUACUUUGAGUAUUGGUAAAAUAUUAAAUAUUGUGCAAGGUAGGAAGAGAAAAACUCAAUGAUUUUUAGCAAUUAUAGAGAUAAAAAUAAUUGAAGGAAUAAAACAGUGAGUGAACAAAAUAUACUGUGCUAUAAUGUUUUGAUAAAAAUAUUCAAAACGGACUUGUUAUUUCCCAAAAAACAUACUUUCAUGCAGAUUGAAAUUUGCAAAUGAUAGUUUAGAAAAUUUAUCUACAGAAUUAUUUCUAUAAAAUCCUGACUUGCAAUGGCAGUCUGUUUUUAUUUAAAGAUUUAUUUGUAUUUUAUGGAUAUUUAGAAUAUCACACAUUUACUAAUAAAUUUCACAUUAUCUGUAAGUAUGAAGGAUGAACUAAAACAUAUAAAAAUAAAAGUUAUAUAUGAAAACAGAUGAUUGCAAACUAAUGAUUCUUUGGAUUAAAAUACACCAGAAGAAAAGAAAAUAUUUUAUCAUAGACUGAAAGUUGGGAUAUGUAAAUGAAGCAAGAGACUUUGGAAUGACAGGACAAUGUGAGUAGAACAGAAAAACUUUACAAGGUAAAUUAAUUAUUUUAGGGAGAAAUGGGUUCUCUUUAAUGCGUGAAGAAUCACCUGGAAGCUUACUAAAUAUUGAACUCUGGGGCCCUCUCCUUGCGUGAUUCUAAUGGAGAUGUUUAUAUACCACACCUUUCAAAUGGACCACACCUUUGAAGAACAGUGAUAUUGAGGCUUAUAUGCACAAUAAAAUGCUCAUUUCUUUCUUUAUCUCCUUUUCAAUGAAUUGUCUUAGUACUAAGUAUUAUACUAAUAACAGUUUGGGGUACCUCUGAGUUGGGAAAAGGGGAAAAUCAUGAAAGAAUUGAGGAGUUUGCCAAGGGUUGCAAACUGCUAGUUUUGGGGUUGAAAUCAGUCUGCAAAUGUAUUUUGUUUUGCAUAGCUGGUGGUACUCCCCAACCCCCAUUGCAUUUGAUUGGCCACAGUCGGUACUGCUCCCUGUUACCCUGUACUGCACCCAUGGCUUCAUGGAUUUGCUUCACCUGCCUGUUUGUUAAUGGCAUUAAAUUGUGGCUGACCAUAGAGGACCUCAGUGACAGAUAUCUUGGCAAAGAAAUGAUGGCCCAGUUAAAAUAAUAUAUCACUAACCUUAGCAAAUAAUUUAACCUAAACUGGUUUCUUGAAAAAUAUUUGUCAGUUUUAUGUAUAACAAUUCUUACAUUCUGUCAAUUUUCUAACUUUCAAAGGAAGUCCUAAAUUUUCCCAUUAGUGAAUAGGACAGAGUAAUUCACAAUAUUGCAGAAUAUGAAAGUCAUUUAUUGUUAUUUUAGCAGCACAUUUCAUGGCUGGCAGCUGUAGAUGUACUUUUCUACUUCCUUUUUUUUUUCUUUUCUGGUCAGUUGUUAAAACUAAUCUUUAUUCUGUUCGUGUUGCCAAUAGGAUACAAUGGAGACACAGCCCAUAACUGAUCAUGGAAAAAGUACAUCUAUAUGUAGAGUUUUAAGUUCCAGUCCUUGAAGGGAUUUUGAGAAAUAAUGAAAAAUAGAAAGCAAAGCCAGCAUUAACUGAUAAUUUACGCCAUUCCAGACACCAAACUGAACACAGUAUUUGUGUUUUAACCCUCCCAACAGAUUUAUCAGUUAAUAGCUACUCUACUAUUCCUGUAGAUGAGGAAACUAAUGCUCAGAAAUGUUAAGUAAUUUGUCCACAUUGCCUUUAUAAAGGCAAAAUUUGUAUUUUAAGAAACCUUUGUAAAGGUGACCAUAGAUGAAUAAUAUAGUAUUUGAUCUUGUAAGAAAAAUGCCUGCCGUUUAAAAUGUGUCUCUUCUUUAAGUUGCCACACUAUGUAAGUUGCCAGGAGAUAGACAUACCACAUAAGCCACGUGGCCAGCAGAAAUGAUUAGUAGCGACAAGCACGUGCCUAAACAUAUCCUGCCCUCUCCCUUUCUGACUAGACUUGCCUCUGCACUUCCACAGUUCCCUCCCUCCAGCAGGUGCAGAAUGGCCUGUUUCUCCUUCAUCCUAUGAUGCUAGUGGCCUUCAUCCUGUGAUGUUAAAUAAGAUGGACUCGCUUUUGCCUGUAGCCUCCUCCUUCAGCUUGCAGAUAUAUCUGACCUUUCUUUCACUCAAAUUACUCAUGAAAUCCCAUUGCCUCUGUGAAUCUGACCUAGUUGGAAAAAACAAGCAAAUUCCCCUUGCUUUUCUCCUGCUGUUGGAGCAUUCACUUCUCAUCAGUUGCUUUCCAUGCAAAGGUGAUUCUGCGCCUUCCUGUGUGUAGUGCAAAGUUACGUAAUGAAUGCCUCCAGGGAUAGGGGCAAGCAAGAGCUGUAACUGAUGUGGAUAUUAUUAUUAAGGGUUUUUUUGUUUGUUUUGUUUUUGUUUUUGUUUUUUUGUUUUUUUUUGAGACUGAGUCUUGCACUGUCGCCUGGGCUGGAGUGCAAUGGCGGAAUCUCAGCUCACUGCAACUUCCACCUCCCGUGUUCGUGCAAUUCUCCUGUCUCAGCCUCCUGAGUAGCUGGGAUUACAGGCACACACCACCACACCUGGCUAAUUUUUUUAUUUUUAGUAGAGAAGGGGUUUCACUAUGUUGGCCAGACUGGUCUCGAAUUUCUGACCUCGUGACCGCCUGCCUCGGCCUCCCCAAGUGCUAGGAUGACAGGCGUGAGCCACCACACCCAGCCUAUUAUUAAGUUUUUACAUUGCCAGCAUUUAUUUCUAUCAUUCUGUUCCGGGCUGUACUCUUAAACGAGGCUACUUUAUUAGUUAUCCUAAGUACUGCUUCAGAAUAUUCUUACAUGGUCCCUUUGCUUGUCCAUCAGGAUCACCUAGACACAUUACUAUUUCAAACCCCAAAUAAAUGAUGCUUCCUUGAAUUUGGCUUUUUGUAUCAUUGAGGUGUUAUAGAACUCUCUCACCUGCUGUCUUUAAGUAAAGAGACAGUGUGUCCCUGGAGCCCCGCAGUGCACAGGAAGGGCUCUCAUUCAAUGUUGAGUACAUAUUGCAUAUGCAGAGGAAAUGGUCCCCUCCACCUCCAUGCCCCUACAGUUAGUUUACUCAAGUUCUCUUCCUUUAGCUGAGUUGGGAGCAGUUAUUUUCCCUCCUCCCCCUUCCUGGGGCUCUGUACUCACCAUUGAAGAGAGGCUAUAUAUUAGAAUUUGGAAUGCUGAGAAGAGACUCGAUGACUGAGGCAGUGCUAAUCCAAGAGGGUUGCAGUGCCCCAGGAUUCAUGUUCCUUCCCAUAGGAUAUAUGGCUUUGAAAGUGAGGGAUCCUAUACUAAAAGGGUAAUAUUAGUCUUCUGGAUUUGGAAGCCAUUUUCCUAGCUCUUCCUGCAUUCCAAGGACAUGAAAAAGGAAGCUGGGCAUUUGUAGUGAAUAACAGGAUCACAACAGGGUCAUAACAAGAUAGCUAGGAAUCUUAAAUUUGUACAAGUAAUCAAGAAUUGUUUUUCUAGUAGUUCCCUUCAAAUUCCCUCUCUUUAGGGCCUAUACAUUUCGGCUUCAAUUUUGGGGUCUAAUUAGUGUAAGAUGAAAUGAUACUGGAUUUCUAUGUAAAAUAGUAGUAUUACCUAACUUUAUAAGGUUCUAGGGAGGGUUACACUAAUGAACAUAUAUAAAACACUUUAGAAUAAGUCCUGGUAAAUAGAAAGUGCUCAGUACACAUAUUAUUGCUAUUACUAUUUCAUAACAAAAAAGACAAUAUUUCUUUUAAAAAACUUAAUAAAUCAAAAAUGUUUCACAUGUAGGGUUUUAUUUAUAAUAUAUGUGCCCUAUUCAUAGACCCACUAAGAUAGCCAAGAAAUUGCCGUGGCAGGAAUUGCCAUCGGAAGAGAAACAUCACCUCUUGGUCUUGAAAUAAGUGAUUCCUGUCAUCAGUGUGUCAGACAGCUUUAUGUGAUAAUGAUUUUGGACAAACCUAAUGCAGAAAGUCUGCUGAAUAUUUAGUCAGAGUUAUACUAGAGAGCACUUGAAGUCCUGUAAAUCUAAAGGUUUAGAGUUAAUGUUCCUGUAAAGCUAAAGGUUUAUAAUAGCUAUCAAAAGAGUUUAGAUUAAUUCAUAAAAUUAAUCUACUAAGUGAUUUCAAGUAGGCAAAUUAAAUACCUAUUUUGAUCUUUUCAUAUUUAUACUAGUCAAAUUUUAAUGAAUUGAGCUUUUUGAGAAUUACUGAGCAAAAUUCUUGGUUUACCAAAUUUUGCAUUAAUAGAUUUGUUUCGCAUAGGAGUAGACACAAAGUAUAGCGUUAUGUACAAAAAGUGCUUAAAUGCAGUUAUAUAACUUUCCUAUUUUCUUUCAUGAUUUCACUAAGGAGUAAACAUUCUUGGCUCGGCGCAGUGGCUCACGCCUGUAAUCCCAGCACUUUGGGAGGCCGAGGCAGGUGGAUCACAAGGUCAGGAGUUCAAAACCAGCCUGGCCAAGAUGGUGAAAUCCCGUCUCUCUUAAAAAUACAAAAAUUAGCUGGGCGCAGUGGCAGGCACCUGUAAUCCCAGCUACUCAGGAGGCUGAGGCGGAAGAAUUGCUUGAACCUGGGCGGCAGAGGUUGCAGUGAGCCAAGAUCGUGCCACCGCACUCCAGCCUGGGCAACAGAGUGAGACUCCAUCUCAAAAAAACAAGAAAAAGAUUCUUGAAAGCCUCCCCACUCCCACUUAUCUUGGAGCAACUGCUGUGGAGUUCGAACAUUCUUAGCUUUGCCAGUGUAAACUGUGUCAUACGUGUAUCUUAAACUACUUCAGGCUUAUGAUCUGGCCAGUUACUAUUCGGUGGUUAUGCAGGAGAGGCCUGGUUUAACAGAAAUCAUGCGGUGGUCAAGAACAAAUUUAAUGAAAAUUGAACAUGUUACCCAGAGUGCUAAUAUGGAAUUUUCUCUGGUGACUACUAUUGCCUUCCUCAGAAGGUUUUUGUUAUUGUGUUGGUGGUUAACACAGGAAUGACUGGUGACGUUUUGUCAGCUUAAUAGCGCCGUUGCAAGAUUCAGGAGACCCUUUUGCCAGGCCAUUAGCCAGCUCUGUGGGUGUAGUCUGAUCUCUUAAUAGCCCUGUGCCUUAGCUUAUGUCUUUAAUAAAUGAGGAAUUCAGGUAGAGGAUCUUGAAGACCUUUUGCAGCUCUGGAAUCUCAAUUUUGUGUCAUUAAACUCUAACAUUCUUUGAAAUAUAGCAUGCUUUGUUGAGUGCUGAUCUGAAUUAAUUAGGAUUUGAUGUUAAACUGGCCAGGAAAUUAUGAGGCAUGGAGGAGGUGACACAGUGGGUGUGCCCAACAGCGUGACUCUUUGUAUCGUUCUCCUGUUUUAUCAAGCAUCAAGAUGCUUCUGAAACACAAAUCUAAAAAUUGUAGUGCUCUCAGUUCUUCUCUUCCUUAAGCCGUACUAUGGUGGUGCUGUGCCUAGGUUGACAUCGUAUUAGCACACCUUCUUUUGCUUUGACACUUACUAUGUGAAAGGAAGAUGACUUCUCCUUAACAGGAAUUCUCUAACACCAUUUGGCACAUGGUUGAGCUGAACAAAUUAGGAAGGAAAAAUAGUCCAAAAUAUUCCAGACCGCAUAGUCAUCUAGUUACAGUGCCUCUUGCAGUGAAACUCAGCUGAAUGCUGUGUACGUGAUGGCAUUACUUACUUCCCAGUAUCAAAUGUGUGCAAAGGGUGAAAUUGGACUUUUCAGGAUCACAUGAUAAACAGAUGAUAAGGAAAUGAAACAGUUUUCAUGUUAGAGUUUCAAAGACAUCUUAAACCUUUUUCUGGAAGAAAAUAUGUUUUUAUGCCACUUGGUAAAGUGGGAUACAAAAUAUUUGUGACUUGAUUUUUUAAUUUGAUAGGAAUAGAUAAUUAAAUAUUUGGUCAAUGAAGGAAGAUAACAGUGUUGGGGAUGAUAAAUUUUAGGGGCCAAAUUGUCUGUGCUGGCAGCAGGCAGAAGGCUGGGUCAGUCACCUGUGCAGAGUUCUUUGUAACUGUUACUUGGUUCUCAUUGCCAGCAGCUGUAUUUGAUUUACUUCCUUAGUUUUGAUAGCCACAACAUUUAUGAUCUGUUCAAACACUGGCAGAUUAAAUACCAUAAGAGGAUUACUUAACACAGCAGUCACAGAUGAAGUAUCUGUUCAUAUUUUGUUUUUGUGUUAAGAAAGAAGGCCUGCCACUAGGUUUGGGUGUGCAGGGAUUCACUGCCUGGUAGUGCCUUUUGGGAGACCUUCGCCGGGCCCUUGAAGCCAUUUCUAAUUCCGGCUCAUCCCCUUCAUAUGUGUAUACUGCAAGGCUUGCCUUCAUUAGAUUUUGUUCUGGGAAAGGUCCAAGGGGAAAACACACCUCUCCUCCAUGUAAUUUUGUAAUCCAGUUUACACCAACUUUUGGAUACUGUCUUAAAGACACUGAAUGAUUUUCAAAGCAUACAAAUCAUUUUCUUUGUAUCAUAAACAUGAAAAUAACAUAAACACCCAGAGAUGAUUUUGUUGAGAGACAUGAACUAAUUAGGGGUUCUUGCACUUAAAUGCACUUUCAGAUCAUCUCAAGAACUUGUGUAAAUAGACCUGGUCCUACAUUUCCUGGGAUGGGCUAUGCUGAGGGCACCUUUCAGAUAGGCUGGGUGUAACUCCCAGACCAGCAGCAGCAGCUUAGGAGCACUUGGCCUUACCUAACCUCUUGGGACCUCUGUUUCUCCACGUCCAAAUUGUUAGCAACGAUUUCCAGCUAGUAGGCUUCACAGAGCUGCUGUACUUGGAACUGAACACAACAUGAUACUUUAUUGGAGUGUAUUAUUUUAUCAAUAAUGUAGCUUGAAAACAAGUUUUCUGUGUUUAUUCAAACCUCUGUGUAGUGAAUUAACAACAACAAUUGCUGAUGUUUAUAGGAUUCUCAAAAACAUACUUAAUAUUUCCCUGCUUUCUUUUUUGGAAGUGUUUUUCAUGUUUUCCCAGUUUCAUUCUUGUCUUGGUAUGAGUCACUAGCAUGAAACCUGAUAUUUUGUUUUAUUAUUUAUUAAUGGGCUUCUUAGACAUUUACCAAUGAAUAAUUAAGCAAUACAAGGAGUGAAACAGAUGUUGGGUUUAGUAGUCAACUGACACUUUCUGAUUUAGCAUGGUAAACUGAAUUUGGAAGAUGCUAGAUAAAUGCCUAAUGGCUAUUUUGCAUUGAAAUUUAAUAAAUAAGGAGUAACUUGAUGAAAGCUAAAACUUAACUUUUUUCUGCAAUUCUUAAUUUUUCUUCAUUUCUUAACUGUUCUAAGGCAAUCAUUUGAAAACAAAAUGUAAUAAACUUAAGAAUAAAGUUUGGAAUAACAGCACAGUUGGAUACUGCUAACAUACUUAUUUACUUUUUUAUUAUUUGUGUCAUCAAUAUUUUUGUUAUAGAAUGACUAAAAGUUGGAAGAUAGAAGUGACAACUUCUUAUAAAACAAGUAUUCUUUGUACUGUUUUAAUAUUAUGGAUUCAACAUACGCAAGGAAAAAUUUUGAAGGUAAAAUUAAAAAGAUUUCUUCUCUGUUUUGUAGAACUGUUGGGUCAUAUUCCACUCCAGUGUAACUUUAGAACAACAACAACAGCAACAAUGUUAUUUUAAAUAUAAAAACUGAGUAUAUUUCCUGCUUCAAAUCAACCCACCUUUGGGCAUAUUUUCUCACUUUGUUAAGUGGGUUAGAGAAAUAGAAAAUACAGAUACUACCCAAACCUCAAUUUCAGGCUUCCCAGGAAAUGUUUUUUAAGAACAGGGAAUUGAAUAUGAGUUUUGUCUUUUUGCCCACUCAUGAUUAUCCUGCUGGUCAUCAGAAUGCCUUUCGGCUGAAGCUAGACGGAAUGAGGGUAAGGAGCAGACAUUCCCUGUAAUUGAAGGCCUGAGAUUCAUGGGAAUGGAUGCUGUGUUCCAUGUCCUAGGUCUGUGGACCUGCUUUGCGUCACAUGCACUGAUCCUAGGGACAGAGUGAAUAUUGAACAAGCUUAUUUAGGAAAAUUUGAAAUGUGAGCUUUGAGAUCAUUCACAUCUCUUGGAUCUGAUAACUCAUCGAGAUGACCCCCUUCACCACCUUCCCACAAAUGGAACAGAGAGAAUCGUAAGGUUGGGUGGUAGAAAGGCCUUGGAGCUCAUCUAUGCAGCCUCUCCUCCUUAAAGUAACCCCUUCUGUGGUGUUCAGGUUGAGGGACCUAUUCCAACCAUGGACUGAGAACAAAUCAGACUUUACAAAAAGAGGUUGACCAUUUAUAUGAUUACAUUUUUAGGUACACAGCUAAGUAAAUAAACUAUAAAGUUGACUAAUUUGUCUUGUAAAAACAAACCAAAUAAGUAAAUAAACUAUAAAGCUUGACUGAUUUUCACAAAUACCUGUGGCAUUUGUGAAAGAUGAGUCCAAACAUAUCUUUAGCAAUAACUGAUUUAUUAAAAUAAGUGAAUGGGCUGGAUGAAGUGGCUCACACCUGUAAUCCCAGCACUUUGGGAGGCCAAGGCGGGCAGAUCACUUGAGGCCAGGAGUUCAAGACCAGCCUGGCCAACAUGGAGAAACCCCGUCUCUACUAAAAAUAGAAAAAUUAGCCGGGCAUGGUGGCGUGAGCCUGUAAUUCCAGCUACUAGGGAGGCUGAGGCAGGAGAAUCGCUUGAACCCAGGAGGUGGAGGUUGCAGUGAGCUGAGAUUAUGCCACUGCACUCCAGCCUAGGUGACAGAGUGAGAUUCUGCCUCAAAAAAAAAAAAAAAAAAAAAAAGAACACUUGACUGCGUUCAGUAUUCAUAUUUUAUAAAUGUGCCCUAAACAAAGUAUACUGGGGUGAAGAUACAGGAUAUACAUCUUGGCCUCAUAGUGUUUUUAAUCUUAUCUAAAGAAUGUAGCUUUUUUUAAAUUAAAAAGUUAUUUUAUAACCUUUUUAAAUAUAGAUGUUUUCAAUGACAAUAUAGUAUUUUUAGCAGCUCCGCAGUAUUAUGUUUUAUAGAUGUCUCUUAUUUAUUACAUCAGGGCCCUAUUGAUUGAUUGAUUUAUGUGUUUCUGCUUUCUACCUAUUAUUUUCUACCCUGUUUUAUUCCCCCAGCCAUGAGAACAUUGUAGUGAUUAUCCUUGUACCUGUGUUUUUAAUACUAACUGGUUUCUUUCAUAAAAAGUGUUUAGUGAAAAACAAAUGCUGUGCGUGCUCAUUAAAAUUUCAGAUGGCACAGAAAUAAAUGAAAUGAGAAGUGAAGCUUCCUUCUCCUUCCCCAUUUCCUCCCUAGAGAUAACUACCUGUAAACAUUUGCUUGUUUAUCAGUACAGAUGUUUUUGUUUUUCAUACAUGAGAAAGCAGAUAUUGGAACUUUAGUAGAUGGGCAAUAGGUUGCAGAAACGAGCAUGGGAAGGUAGCUGUAUUCUGAAUGGGGAAGGCUUGUGGGAGCAAACGGCUGCUGGUGUGUGUGUUCAAGGAUGGGACAAAAAUGUGUUGUAACCUGUUUUCCUGCAUCAGGUAGUGACAGCCAUGUAGCGUGGAGGCACAGAAGCAAAUCAGGGAAGAAUCAGCACUAAGAAGUGAGCAAGCUUAAUAACAUACUGCAGCUAGAAAAUGAGUUACUUCCCCCAAAUGGGAGAUUCCCUUUGUAAGGAAUUGAGAAUUUCAUGAUGAGUUUAGAGCUGACCAGCACAUGAAUAUGAGCUUAAUGGAAUCAUUUCUAAUUGCCUCCAGAGAAGCAAAGUUUCAGGAAGGGAACCCGGUAAGAACAUUAUAGUAUGUAGUUUAACCCAGAUAUGAUAAGUUUUUUGAUAAGAGAAGAGUCAGGGUAAAUAGGAAGGUUCAUCUGUGAGAAAUAAAGUACAGGAAGAGGGAAUGGAGCUGGAGGAGGGGGGAUUAUGUGAGGGUUGUUUUACACCAGAUGGAGCAAGACUUGGCUGCAUGGAUCGGGAAUCUUUUUUGAGGAUAGCUUCUUCCAAGGAUUCAAGACAAAAACCAGAUUGCAGGAAAUUCAAGGGGGAAUUGGAGAAUAGGAUUCUGAACCAAGGUGGAGCUUUCAUUGAGUUAGAAUAUGAAUAAAGAUACGGGAAAUAUGGAAAAGUUUCCUGCCCACAAGGAGAAUGUGCAUGUGAAUCUCUAAUAUUUCCCUUUAAAAAUAAAAUGAAGCUCCCAGCUCUGGUAGACCUGGUGUUAGCCCCACAUCUUUUCCUGCAGACAGAGCAAUAGGUCUUUCCCUUCCUCUAGCUCACCUAUGCCAAUUUUCCAGAGCUGUCAGGUCUAGGGCUGAGAUACUGGUUGUGGCUCUGCCCCAGCUGCUGCUGUUCCCUCAUUAACUCCAACCAAGGGCUUUGGGACUUGUGUGGCCGGCACUACUGCUCACUCAUGUUGGGGUCCAUGCUAACCAAGUUCAUAUUUGCUGGGAGCCCUCUCUCAGCCCCAGGAGUAUUCCAAAGCCCCUGUUUCUCCCAAGAGAUUCAGAAUUUGAAUUCUGCUUUGGUUCCCAUUGUGGAAUACUGCUGUGACAAUCUGUCUCACUCCCCAGUGGCCUCUGAGCCUUGUGUUGCCACCACAUUCAUUUCUGCCCCUAAGGACUGAAGUUCCAUCCUUGAACUUGCCUCUGCACCAGGGCUGAGCUAUCUUUGCUUCUAGCCUCAUGGUGUGUGGCUGUUGCUCUACAGCCUGGUGGUGUCCUGGGUUCACAUACCAGUUUUGCCGCUUAGUAUUUCUUUGGGUUCAGGCCAGGUAUUUAACCUCUCAGUGUCAGUGUCCUCAUUUUGUAUUUUAAUAAUAUGAAUUUUCUGUCUGUUAUCCUAAGAAGGUGGCUGCUUCAGUAAAUGCAAGGGAAUUGAUUGAACACAGGCCUCGAGGCAUGUGUGAGAUCCUCUUGGGGAGACCCUGGGGCACCUGAAAGGAGUUACAGUCUUGUGGGAGAAGUGGGCUGUCUGUAUCAAGACAUUGUGGGCAGAGGAACCGACACCAAGUUCCAAUGUGACUCCCAAAUGGAAAGUAUCUAGGGGCAGAUGCUUCACACGGAGCUGUUGGUUCUUGGUCAGGUGUUUGUCUGUUCAUGUCCUUAGGGUCCAGGUUCAGUGGCUGUAGGAAUAUUCAUUUAAAAAGGAUAAUAAAUCUCCUAAACAAUGCUAGGGAGGCUUCCCAGGCUGCAGAAUCAGGAAAAUAAAAUUUACCUCACAGGGUUAUUUAUAGGAUGAAUGGCAUGAUUUGGGCCUAACGAAUAAUGGAUGUUCAGUCAACAGUAGCGGUCGUUCUUUCUGCUGUGCUCUGCCCACUUCUUAGGACGCUGUGUUAAUUCUUGCAUGCACAGGCCUAGGCUGCCCUCCUGGCUGGACCCCACAGUCAUCUGCCCCCCCUCUGUGUCCUCCUUCAUCCGUGUCCUCUUCCAUCCCUACCGCUAGGUCCCCCGCUUUCUGAGUAGUCCCGUGUCAGGCCUCAGUCUCCCUUUCUUUGCUGGAAAAGGGUAAAAGGCCAUCUCUGGCUGAUGAGUGCUAGCAGUUUGUGUCCUGUGUUGGGAUAGUGAGCCUGCAGUCCAGUGAGGUUCCUGCGAGGAGCAAGAUUUGGAUGCAAUUCUUCAUCAGUUUAAAAUGACUAUAGUUUUAAAUAUUACCUAUCUUUUACUACAUUUAGGCCCUCUGAGGAUUUAAUAUAGGCACUAUUUUGUUAAUUGUUUAUACUAUCUUAUAAACAUGUUAAUUCACAAAUAACAUUAUUUUAUUCAAAAACAUUUAUGCCGUUUUGAAUUGUUCCUUUGUAUGAUAGGUAUAGGAGAUAUUCAGAAAUAAAUAUUAAUAACAAUAGUUAACACCUGUCUAACACUUUCUUGUGCCACGUAUUCUUCUAGCUACCUUCACACAUGUUCAUUCAUUUAAUCCUCAAGAACCACCCUAUGAAGUAGGUGCUCCUAUUUUCUUCUUUUUAUGGAUGGUGGAAAAAGAGGCCCAGAGAUUUUAAGUAAGUUGCUCUAGGUCCCACAGCUGUUAAGUAGCUGGGCUGUGAACAGAGGCCUUAUGGCUCUGACACCUGUGCUCUGAGACCAGGCUGCUUCCAUGGCGCUGAAGUCUUGGCAUCAUCUGGCCCCUGGUUAGACAUGCAGAAUCUCAUGCUCCACCCCAGAACUGCAGAAUCAGAAUGUGUGUUUUAAUAAUGUUCCCAGGACAUUCGAAUGCACAGUCAAGCUUCAGAAGCACUGUUCUAAACCAUUCUGCCUACUUACUGUCUCUCCAGCCAUGGGAAUUUCAUUGUUGUGGGGGAAAUAAAGGGGCAUGUAUGGGUAAUAGCUGCCCUUGUAACAUUUUGGUGAAACAGAUUGAACACCAGUUGAGUGCUUUAGACAUUUCAGAUUCCUUCCCAGAUAGCCUCGUGUCACACACUUCUGUUUCUUGUACCCACACAUGCAUACACAACCAGUCACACAUGGCUUUUGUGAAGUUUAGUAAAUUUAGAGAUAACAUGGGAUGGCACUGGCAUAGGGCAGAGUCAUGCUUGUGGUGUUUUGAAAACUUGUCCUCUCUUCGUUUUAAGUUGGGGCCCUCCCCACAGCCUGUGCCCCUGGGAAGUACAGUCCAGCCCAGGGCUCACUGCUUGCCUCCUUGUGGAAAUAGCCUGGAUAGACUGGUCCUCACCCUUCCCCCUCAUUCCAGUAAAUAAAUGUCUUUCUUGUUACAUAAGUAAUUAUAAUCCAAAUGUAAUCACAUAAUAGACAUAGAAGGAGCAGCCAGCUGGCCUCUGGGGAGUUGGCCAACUUAAAGGACAAGAAUGGGGGAGGUUUUGCCCAGCAGAGAAGGAUAUUUGGGGAAAGGGAAGUAAAAAGCCUGAAGGUCUGAAAGAACAUAGCUUGUUACUCGGGAGAAGUUGGGCGUAGCCCGGAGAGGGCAAAUGAGGCUUUAUUGUGAAUGGCUUUAUUUGCCAUAAUAUUAAGUUACAGAAUUUAUUUUGUGGCAGUCAGGCUCUACCUGUAUUGCUAAGGGCUCUACCUGUAUUUUUUGCAAACAAACCCUGUGAGCUAGGCAUCAUUAUCCUCAUUUUGCAGAUGAAGAAAGUGACAGGUCCCUCAACUUGCUCAAAGCUACCUAGCUAGUGGUAGUACCUGAAUCUGAUACCCUGGGCUUUAACCCAUGUGUUACUGUUGAUCCGUAUAGCAACUGCUUUAAGGCAUCAGAAAUACACUGUUAUUGUGUAAAAUAAAGACUGCAGUUAACAACAAUACAGAGAAGGUUUCAUUUUAUUUUAUUUUAUUUUUGUCUUAUUCUGCAUUGCCUAUUUGAAGAGACUGGUUUUUCCAGCAGUCAGUGGUGGAGCACGACUGCUGGGUCAUACGCCCAGGUUUUGCACGUUGGUUUGUGGGGUGCAGGCACUGACUGACUAGUGCUAAGACGUAAUGUGCUUUUGAUGGAGUUUCCUUUGCCUGGGUGUUUUUGGGGUUUUUGGAAAUGUGGAAUCUUAAGAGGAAGAAAACAUAGUAUUUAUAGAGCUGGAAAAUGUUCUGCUUAUUCUCAAUCCUUUAUUGACAUAGUGGUUACUCUGCUGUUUUGGUUGGCAGUGUGAUUCUCUUAGUUUAAGCAAAAAUUUCUUUUGUCAACAGGUAGAUUACUAAUAAGGAUAUUUUACUCACCAAGAAAUUCCUAGGAACCCUUUUUCUGGACACAUCAGACUUCACAAAAUGUUUCUGUUUUUCUUUAGUUCCUGUUGCUUCUCUCUUCUUGCAGUAUCCACUAGCAGCAUGGUGGUUGUUCUGUAGAUAGUGAUGUUACCACUUCACCAUUUGGUCCUCUCUCCUCUGCGUCAGUUAACUUCCCAUCUAAUAUUUUGUUCUGUGAACUAUUCCAGGAAUGAUUAUCAAGCUCUCGUCCUCCACUUAAAGUAGCAAGGCAUGCUAGCAUUUUCUGUUUAGGACUGAAGAAAUGCCUGCAAUUCAGGAAGUGUGGCAACCUUAUAAGUAGUGGGAAAGUUAGAGGAUGUAAACUUGGGUGAUUCGCAUAACUUCAGUAGACCUCAGUUUCCUCAUUUAUAAACGAGGAGGCAGUCUAGAGCCUUUAGAUGCGGCCUCUAAGGGUCCCUUGGAUGAGGUGUAAAGUUCAUGUUCUUAGGGAACUUCACCACUAGUACUUGGCUGCCUUUAAUAGGUCUUAAUGCUCCUAUAAAUUUAACUAUAUUAUCCCUUUUGCCCAUUUAUGAUUUAUUAAUAGCUUUAAUGAAUUGUGAAUGACAGUUUAAUUAGAUCAUCCAUGUAUAAUUAGGGCAACCGGGUUUUUUUCCCUAAGAGGAUAUAUUUUUCAUCCGUGAGUAUGUAGCUUACCUCUAACCUAGGUAAUUAAGCAUUUUAAGGCAUUUUCCAAAAUAAGAAGGCUUUUUCUGUUUUCCUAAUAAACACUUUAUUGAAAAGCCACAUGCAUAAAAUAAUGGAGGGCCGUUUUGACCUAGGUUUUGCAUGUAAUCAUAACCCAGACAGACACAACCUGAGGCAGUACAUUUAGUUUAGUGGUAACAAAGCAGUGUGGAAUUUAAGAAAUCUCUCUCUCUCUUUUUUUUUAAACUACUUAUUUUCUUACUUUUUGAGUAAAGCAACUUUAUAGCUACUUCAUAUCUGUUUCAAGUGCUACAUUUUCAAAGCUGGCAAAUAGAUUUACCUCUUUUGUGAAGGUGCCACAUUAAACACUUAAAAGAAGAAAAUCAGCCUUAUCUGAUGGAUGAUCCCCAGUUAAUAGCCCAAGAACCAAUUUGUAUUUGGCUUUGCGAUGUGUUUUUCUACUUACAUUUGAGUAUGGGUGUGCCUGAUAUUCUCGGAAUUUACAAUACUUCAAACAAAUAAGGAAGUUGCACUGUGAAGACAGACUCAGAAGGAACUGGAAAGCUGACAGACCUUUGUGCUUCCCCAGCCGCCUUGCUGAAUUCUCUGCGGUGGGUUGAGACCCCUGGUGUUCUUGGAUGGGACAGCCCACAUGAGCAGAGUGGCUCUCCCUUGUUUCCUUUGCUCUCUUUGGAUUUAUAUCCUUCCAGAACUAGCUGUUUCGUAAAGUAUUUAGACUCUGAAUACCUGAAUUAUUCAGAUCUUCUUGUCACUCCAAUCACAAACAGGGACAGGAGAGAGUGGCAAGAGUACGUUUAUCAAGCAGAUGAGAAUCAUCCAUGGGUCAGGAUACUCUGAUGAAGAUAAAAGGGGCUUCACCAAGCUGGUGUAUCAGAACAUCUUCACGGCCAUGCAGGCCAUGAUCAGAGCCAUGGACACACUCAAGAUCCCAUACAAGUAUGAGCACAAUAAGGCUCAUGCACAAUUAGUUCGAGAAGUUGAUGUGGAGAAGGUGUCUGCUUUUGAGAAUCCAUAUGUAGAUGCAAUAAAGAGUUUAUGGAAUGAUCCUGGAAUCCAGGAAUGCUAUGAUAGACGACGAGAAUAUCAAUUAUCUGACUCUACCAAAUACUAUCUUAAUGACUUGGACCGCGUAGCUGACCCUGCCUACCUGCCUACGCAACAAGAUGUGCUUAGAGUUCGAGUCCCCACCACAGGGAUCAUCGAAUACCCCUUUGACUUACAAAGUGUCAUUUUCAGAAUGGUCGAUGUAGGGGGCCAAAGGUCAGAGAGAAGAAAAUGGAUACACUGCUUUGAAAAUGUCACCUCUAUCAUGUUUCUAGUAGCGCUUAGUGAAUAUGAUCAAGUUCUCGUGGAGUCAGACAAUGAGAACCGAAUGGAGGAAAGCAAGGCUCUCUUUAGAACAAUUAUCACAUACCCCUGGUUCCAGAACUCCUCGGUUAUUCUGUUCUUAAACAAGAAAGAUCUUCUAGAGGAGAAAAUCAUGUAUUCCCAUCUAGUCGACUACUUCCCAGAAUAUGAUGGACCCCAGAGAGAUGCCCAGGCAGCCCGAGAAUUCAUUCUGAAGAUGUUCGUGGACCUGAACCCAGACAGUGACAAAAUUAUCUACUCCCACUUCACGUGCGCCACAGACACCGAGAAUAUCCGCUUUGUCUUUGCUGCCGUCAAGGACACCAUCCUCCAGUUGAACCUGAAGGAGUACAAUCUGGUCUAAUUGUGCCUCCUAGACACCCGCCCUGCCCUUCCCUGGUGGGCUAUUGAAGAUACACAAGAGGGACUGUAUUUCUGUGGAAAACAAUUUGCAUAAUACUAAUUUAUUGCCGUCCUGGACUCUGUGUGAGCGUGUCCACAGAGUUUGUAGUAAAUAUUAUGAUUUUAUUUAAACUAUUCAGAGGAAAAACAGAGGAUGCUGAAGUACAGUCCCAGCACAUUUCCUCUCUAUCUUUUUUUUAGGCAAAACCUUGUGACUCAGUGUAUUUUAAAUUCUCAGUCAUGCACUCACAAAGAUAAGACUUGUUUCUUUCUGUCUCUCUCUCUUUUUCUUUUCUAUGGAGCAAAACAAAGCUGAUUUCCCUUUUUUCUUCCCCCGCUAAUUCAUACCUCCCUCCUGAUGUUUUUCCCAGGUUACAAUGGCCUUUAUCCUAGUUCCAUUCUUGGUCAAGUUUUUCUCUCAAAUGAUACAGUCAGGACACAUCGUUCGAUUUAAGCCAUCAUCAGCUUAAUUUAAGUUUGUAGUUUUUGCUGAAGGAUUAUAUGUAUUAAUACUUACGGUUUUAAAUGUGUUGCUUUGGAUACACACAUAGUUUCUUUUUUAAUAGAAUAUACUGUCUUGUCUCACUUUGGACUGGGACAGUGGAUGCCCAUCUAAAAGUUAAGUGUCAUUUCUUUUAGAUGUUUACCUUCAGCCAUAGCUUGAUUGCUCAGAGAAAUAUGCAGAAGGCAGGAUCAAAGACACACAGGAGUCCUUUCUUUUGAAAUGCCACGUGCCAUUGUCUUUCCUCCCUUCUUUGCUUCUUUUUCUUACCCUCUCUUUCAAUUGCAGAUGCCAAAAAAGAUGCCAACAGACACUACAUUACCCUAAUGGCUGCUACCCAGAACCUUUUUAUAGGUUGUUCUUAAUUUUUUUGUUGUUGUUGUUCAAGCUUUUCCUUUCUUUUUUUUCUUGGUGUUUGGGCCACGAUUUUAAAAUGACUUUUAUUAUGGGUAUGUGUUGCCAAAGCUGGCUUUUUGUCAAAUAAAAUGAAUACGAACUUAAAAAAUAAAAGCUGGUAUCUUAAAAUGUAAGAGAGUAAGACUGUGAAGCCUAAAAUGACUGGCUGAGAAUGAACCAGAAAUGCCAUUUGCCAAACAGUUGUAACUAGAAAUUUGAUUCUCACGGUCCAUUCUUUUCUUUGUCCUUAAGAUGACAUUGUUAGUGUUCACGUCCCAUGUUCAGUGUCCAAACCGGCAAUGUAAAAAGUAUCCUGUGUGGUUUAACAGGAAAUCUGUUUAUGUCUCUUUAUUUGAAACCAGUUUUACUCUCAGUGGUUCUUUAAGUUCAAUGAAGUCUGCCAGGAACAUUGGUUGGUAGUAUUAUUCCGACACCUUUAAUUUCCAAAAUCUGAAGUUCCUGCUAGUUUACCACCUUCAUGAUCUUCUUGAACUGGUAACUGAUUAGGUUGAACUUAUGGAAGAUUUGUGGACUUAACUCAAAAGUAACCUCUCAGUGUUCUAUAGAACAUGUAUUUGUGUAACUGAACCUACCAGGAGAAAUGUUUGGAAUUCUAUAUGUGCAAUUUUUCAACAAAUGCAAAAAAAAUACAGCACAUGUAUUGACAAGCUUCUGUCAAGCAGCUUGAGUUGAAAUUUGAUUUAAGAAAAUAAAUCAUGAUUGUUCAAAGCUGCUGGGACGUUAGAAUUAGGCCAUGAUACUGGUCUCAUUUUAACUACAGUGGUAUUUGGCACUAGUGUAAACUUCCAUAUAAAUCACUCUUUUGGAACAACAAAGGGGGAGGGAGAAAAAUCACGGCCUGUUAAAUGAGUACCAAAGCCGCCCAACAGUAAUGAGAUGUUCUCAUCCUUGAUUCUCCCAGCCUCAAACAACACAGCUUACUUUUUUUUUCCCUUGCUCAGAAAGUACCUGUAAUUUAACAAACAGACUGCCUGUAGGUAUAGUGCAAUUACAAAUGCUCUAAUCAUUGUACAUACAUCUCUCUUGAUAUUGCAGCAUCCAUACUGGCUUUGUAAUCAUUAAUUUUUUGGCAGAUUGAAUGUGCUGUAUUGAUAUGUAUCUAUGUAAUUGUAUUGUAUGUCUAUAGCUAAUUCACGUUUUGAAUAAUGUUAUUUUAUUUACUUUUUUAAGAGAGGAGAAUGUAAAUUUGUCAGUUUAUUUCUGACUAGGGAUAUUUUCUUUCCAUUUAGAAAAGAAGAAAAAAAAAAAACCUUACUGUCAUACAGAGCGGUACUAGCGUCGUGCUGUAUAAAAUCAUUUGCACAUUCCUGAGUAGAGGUAUACUGAUUAUAAGACCCAAAGGUAAUUUCAUAGCAAAAUACAUAAAAUCAGUCGGAGCUUUUAUACAAACAUGGAAACCAACUUUGUAGAACUUUUGCCAUUUGAUCUAGGAUUGGAAUAUGAGCUUUUAUACAAUUCAUAUUCUUAUUUGGCAAAUGCACAGUUUAGUAUUACCUCUCUGAUGGCCUUUACUAGAAAGGCAGUUUUAGAAGCUAUUGUGAUCCACUAAGGAAAUGUUUUAACAGCUAGAGACCACUGCUUGCCUGAAAGGGCGUUCUUAAAUUUGGUGCAGCAAAAAAAAAAAAAAAAAAAAAAAAAAUUAAACAACAACAUUUGAAGGCCUACAGUGUGUAUAGAGAAAACCUCAUCACAAGAUCAUAAGUGUUACAGUUUUAGGGAAUCAAGAUAUUCUAUUUAAUAGAGCUAUAGUAAAUGUAGUCAAUUAAACCUGAUCUCAAAGCUUGAAGAAGCUGAGCAAAACAGGGAAAGAUUGUUAUAUUUGUCUUUAUGAAAUUGGGAUGGAAUUUGCUAUGCAGAAUUGAGGUUUGUGGCUUCGCUGUUCCUGUAGGGUGCAUGACAAGAUCCCUUCUCUUGAGAAAGGAAAAAAUUGAUCACCCUAGCAGCAGUGAUGCAUAGAAACCUAAUUUUAGCCACACCAGUCAAUCGAAGCUAAAGGAUUUUCUUUUUUGUUUCUUCGGGGUUUUAUUGAAGGGGCUAGGGGCGGGACGGGAUUCUUUUCAGUUUUGUAUAAAAACAAAGUUUACUCAUGCUUUAUAUUAUAUUGUGAUUGCAAGCGUUAUAAGCGUGUGCCACUGGCCUCCUAUUGUUGAUGCUUAGGUAAUGGAGGCCUGUGGUGAGUUUUAUGGUGACUUGGGCAUGUCUUAUUCAAAAACAAAAACAUAAAACACAGAAACCUUUCUUCAGCAUACCAAGGCAAGCAGCCAUUUCAUGACUCACUUAACACAUUGCAGUGUACCAGUUUACAGAUGAUUUUUCCCUUUUUGCGUGACAUGGCAGUUCUAACCCCCAGAGAAUUCCUUAUUUGUAAAUUGGAAGUUUCUACUAUGCCUUACAGAGCUUAAAUUCAGAAGUUUGUGCCUCAUAUCUGAAACAAAGGGAAAUAACACACCCAUUCAAAAGUAAAUAAAUCUCCUAGAAGUUUUUGUUUUUAACAUUUCCAUAUAAAGAGCUCUGUUGAAUGUCAUGAAUAGACUGGAAAAAAAAAUUUUAAGAACCUGCAUAUGUUGUUUACUAGCAGAUGACAACUACAAAAGGAAUCUGAAGAACACGUAAAACUUGUAUUUUUUUUUUUUUGGUAGAUUAACUAGCAGGCCUAUUUUAAAAAGGUAAUUCAGCUAAAGGGCAAUUUACUUUUUUGUACUUCAGACUAUCUUGAUUGUCAAAGUGUACGAACUGUAAUUUUAAAAUUUAUACUGCCACAUGAUUGUAAAUUUUAGUUGUCUUAAGUUAGGAAUUGGUGAAAAGCUAUUUAUGCUGGAUUUGGGUCAAAAUGACUUAUUUGCAAAAAAAUAAAUAAUGGGAAGAAAGGGCUGUAUAAUGAAAUACUGCAAGACUCACAUAUUGGUUGGAAAUUUCCCUCAAAUCACCUACCGAUUACCCUUGAUUUCCCUUUGUUUUCAGUUUCUCAAAACGAAUGAAAUGAAAUAUAGCAGAAUGUUAACCCAUAUAAAAAUAAAGUGUACCCAAAUAUUGUAAUGUAUAUUGCUGCUCUUCUUCAAAUUAAAUAAGGGUUUAAAACCACUUAAUUGGUAAUCAACAUCUCAAUUGAUACAAAUAAGGUGUGCUUGGUAUACAUUAAUAUUUUCUUCCAAAGAUAUAUCUUUGGUUAGAAACACAAAAAAAUAAAACUAGUAAUAUUGUAUGUUUAUCUAUCUCUACAUAUUUCCAGCAUAUGUAGCGUUAAUAGAUCUGUCCUGGUAACUGUGUCUUUGGGAUUUCAUUUUGGUUCCAUCAAAUUAGGAAAAGAAAUGGCUUAGUUGUAUAUGAUUAGCUAGAGAUUUUUGGAGCCAGACACCUGCUGUUUAGUAGAUAACUUAGUACAGACCCUAAACUUGUCAUUUGUUUUUCUCACAGAAUAGCCAUUUCCUGCUGUCUUCCCAAUGAUCACUGCCCUUUCAAUAACACUCUUGCCUCUAGAAUCAUAUGUUCAAAGUAUGAAUACACACCUAGCACAUAGUAGGUGCUCAAAUAUUAAUUUCCUCCUUGCCUUCCUUAUCUACCCUGUGUCCUCCAUUUCCCCGUAUGAUUCCAACCCAAUAUAGCAAAUGACAUUUACAUGUUAUGAAAACAUCUAUUGGGUAAAAUCAGAUCUUGGAUAAAGAAAUUCUGACUUUUAUAUAAGCUUUUGGUAGACAGAAAAAACAGAAAGGUAUUCGUUGGUAGAACAUUUUUAAGUUCAGGAAAGAAAGCUGGAAUAAUACUACGUAACUUUGUCCAGGUUACUUUGACUGAAACACGUUUUUGGUGGAUUUCUUUUCCUCAAAGAACUCUCUAAAUGCAACUCCUUGCUGGAUUCCUCACCCAUCAUCCUGUUGGAAACCCUUACUAGACCUAUGUAUUUAGGGAGUUUUGUCAGAAAACAUUUUUAACUUGCAGUAUUUAAAAGAAUAUUUACUGUUCCUAAAAUGUCAUUCAAAUGCAUGUACUGUCUAUUGUUUGGGGAUGGGAACUAGUUUUGCAAAAAACACCUAAUGUUGUAUAAUAAUGCCCCAAUGAUCUUGCUGGUUAAAAAUACAGUAUUUUUGGCCAUAAUUUUGUACUAUAGUAUUCUUCAUUGUUGAGUUUUGCUUCCAUUAAAGUUGCCCGAGCCCCUCUCAGAAUGUUUUGUAUUAGUAGGAGUACUGAAAUACAUCUUUCCUUCCUUAACACACCUUGUGCAUAUUGCAUUUUCCAAAAUAAACAAGUUUAAUGGUUUCAAAAAAAAAAAAA